GUAGUGGGAGCUGGAUAGUUCAAGGAGUAACUCCACAUAACUGAGUCGUUUGGAUACCCACACAAGAUAAUUUGGAACGCGCUUGUAUUUUUUUGUUUUUUGAGAUUUCUGGUUUAUGUCCUUUAGAGAGUGGGGUAGGAGCGUAAAGACUGUAUAGGUUGCCUAUGAGCAGGUCCAUACAAUAGCGUUCCCAAGUCUGCCUAAUAGCAAGUUUGUUCUCUCUUUCUCUCUCUCUACCCAAGUGGGUGAAAAAGAACAGUGUGUCAUGAAGACAGGCACCUGGAGGUGAUUUGGGUGGCAUUCAUGAGAAAAUUCACGUUACCCGUAAGUUUAUUCUUGCUAUUUUUAUCUUGAUUUCUUUAAAGAUUUUGUGGGAAUAUCUGCAGUGGGUCGCAGGAGUAGGUAAGAUUGCUAAGGAUCAAAAACAAGUUUCAUGAGAAUAUUAUUUUUGCUACCUUAUAAAAUAGCUAUUGAUUUGUUUGUUGAAGCUGGUUUCAACUGCUCUGUCUUGUUGAGGAGAGAUGAUGCUGAUAAACGUCAUUAUUUUUCCAUCUGAACCCUGGGAGGUAGCUGGCAAGGAUGGAAAAACUGACCUUUUCAAUUAAAGACUAAGAGUCUAAGAGAAGUGACUUGGAUAAGGGUGCAUGUCAGAGCCACAUGUAAGUUUCAACAGAGGUAGAUUUUCCUAUUUGCAGUUUUUUAAACAACACUUUUCAGUUUCUUUGAGUUGUAAAACUUUUCAAGUCAAUUGGGAGUCAAUGCAGUACCUUUUUCCAUGGUCAUUUCAUAUUGGCAGGUAAUUAAGAGUGAUUAGAGAACAAACCUUUCAAAUGAUGUUGGAUUUUUUAUCAUUCACUUAUUUUACCUACUUCUCUCUCCUUUUUGUUCAAAAGUAGGUCUUCUGAUUUCUUUUCCGAUCUAAGCACUAAAUCUUUUGGCUGCAGUUUUUCUUCUGAAAUGUAUACAGGGCAUCCGUUCCUUCAAUUUAGGUCUUAAAAAAAUAAAGCUGCUCAGCAGAAAAUUCCCAUGCAUGGUACUGACUUUUCUACAAGUUUGUCUGAUCAUGAUUUUAACUUGUUGUUUCUUCUUUGUUAUAUUUGAGGACAGACAUAAUAUGCAUUAGCUUCAAUCUCUCUUAUCUUAAAAAUUAAUAUUUUGUAAAAACUUGCUUUUAUAUUAUUUUAGUUGAAUAAGUCUAUUUCAUAUGAUAGGCAGGGGGAAGUCUCUACACACUGAUUUUUUUUGUUCCUUUUUGUUCAUUUUUCCCUGUAAUGCUAUGUUUUAAGCCUAGUGAAGGAGGCAAGGAGGCAGGAUUUACUGCCUAGAUUUAUUGAUCUUCAUUAUUAUUAUUAUUUACUAUCAGAAGAAAUCUGACAACAUAUCAAUAAAAUUUAUUUAUAAACUGAAGACAUGCUGUUAUAUGAUACACUACUUAUAAAACACACAAAGAAACAAAAAAGAUGAAUAAAGCAAAAAUUAUGAAAUAGAAGGUCUCAUGUUGCUGUUAUGUAUCCCGGUGGAUCAUUUUGUACAGCCCCUGGGGUGUGUAGCACACUUUAAAGAUCACUGCUGGUUUGAUAUUUUUAAAAUCUUUCUCUCCUUAUCUCUGCUCUGCUGUUCAUCAUCUCUGAUACUCUAGCCAGUUGUAAAACUGCUACACUUCUAUAUCUUCUGUAACAAAUAGAUUAAGCACACUUGUUUUCCUCUCAUGGACUCAUAUGUGGAUAGAAUGAGGUGUAAAGGAUGAAUGUGUUUUGGAGAUGUCAUCUUAGAUCUCCCAAAGUAGACAUACAGGUGAAUUUUAAAAAAUGGAGUUUUAGUUUAAAGACUAAGUACCAAUGGUCAGGAAGUGAAGAAUCCAAGGAGUAAAUGAGGGAGGAUUGGAAGGACACUUUCCACAUUGCAGUGUUGUGUGGAGGCUGGAAAGUUCAUAAACCUUGAAGCAGAUUAACCUGAAUCUAAGUCUGGCACCAUCAUUUAUUACAUUUACAGUCCUGGGCAAUGUAGUUCCUUAAUUUCUGUGAGCCUUAGUUUCUUUAGGUAUAAAAUUGGGAUAACAUCUAUUUCACGGCAUCACGAUAGGGAUUAAACAUGAGAGCAUGAGUCAACAUGGGUCAAGAGCUUGGCUCUUUUAGAUUGGCUCUUUAGCAGAUAUAACAGAUCCAAAAGGGAUACUGCCUCAGAUGUGAAAUAUAUUUAUUUCUCGGUUGUGUGAAGUCCCAGAAUGGGUGAUCAUGGCAGUACUCCUUCAAAGUGUGAUUCAGAGACCCAGCCUUCAUCUGUUCUGUGCCCUUGCCGUCUUCAGCAGGGUCACUGUGCUUACUUGCAUCAAGCCAUUGGAAAGAGGAAGACUUGGGAGGAUGUUAAUUGCCCAGAACUGGAAUGAGUGCAUAUUACUUUUCCUUGCAUUGUGCUGGCCAGAACCCAGUUCUUUGUGGAUGUACGUUACUAUUAAGGAGGCUGGGAAAUAUAGUCUAGAAAUGUUAUCCAGGAAGUAGAAGAAAUUGUUGGGGGAACAACUAGCAUUCUCUGAUGUUUUAUUACUAUAUGUGAUAUUUCUUCCAUGUUCAAUAACUGUUACUUCCUUUUCUUCUCCUAACCCUUGCUUUUUUUUUUUUCUGGUAGAAAAACUGGAAUGGAUACAAUAAAUAAUAAUAGAAGCAGUUAAUACAUACAUAAUGCUUACUAUUAUUGAGAUACUUUUUAAAGCACAUUGCCCUACUUUGCCCUUCUAAUAUUAUCUCUAUUGUACAGAUGAGGAAAACUAGGCAUAGAGAAAUUAAGUUAUUUGUUCAUCAUAGCUAGUAAGUAGCAGAGCUGGGAUCUGAACCAGGUUCUCUCACUCCAGAAUUGAUUUUUUAACAGCUUUUUUUUUUUUUGCUUUUGCCUCAAUACUUUUCUUAUUUAAGCCACUGGACCGCUUUUUACUUUUGCCUAUAUAUAAAAAAGUUGCCAAGAGAAUUUUUUAAAAUACUAAAGUAGAAAAAAAGGAUAUAAUCCAAAACAUACUGGAAUGGAAUUAGAUAUGAUACAGCUUUAUCUUGAAUACCUACCAGGAUCAGGAGCAGAUAUUUAAAGUAACUCCCCCCACUUACACACCCUUCACCACUACAACUGCUCUUUCAUUUGUGAUAAACACAUUUUCAGGGUCUGUGCCUUGAAUUAUAACCUUCCUCUGAAGAUUCUAUUGUGGGAGUCUUGCGCUACCACUUUCAUGCUUCAGUAUGUGAGGAUAAAUUCCUCUUCACUUCUCAGCAGAAACAAAUAUCUUCCCUGGCAGGUUUUUCAGCUAAAAUAGCCUCUCCUAACUUUUGAUCAAAGGUAUUGCUCUUUAUCAAUAUCCCCAUCCUCCAAGAAAGGAAACCCUCUUCUUUUCCUAUGAGCUUUGCAAAAUUAUUUUUUAUUUAUCUAUUUAUUUAUCUUUAUUUUCUAUAUGACUAAGGGGACUGUAUAUAUAUCCCAGGUACCGUCUAAAAGAAAAUGGUCCCUCUUGUUCUCAUCCUGUUGUCCCAUUUCCAUUAGAGAAUCUGCCUCAUCUUAUGUUUCCUAUGUAUUUGUCUUUCAUAAAAAUGCCUGUUAGAGUUUUGGUUCCCAGUGGCUGCAGUGGAAAUGUGUAGUGGUCAAUAGUAAGCGUAUACUUUUUGCUAAGAUAGUUAUUGUUUCAACAUUAAAGAGUGAUUUUUUUCCUCUUGUUCAGUAUGUAUUUGUUGCAUCUUCACAAUUAGGUAAUGAUAUGUAUCUUCUUACCAUGUAGGUAGGCAUAAAUACUGUAUACCUACCAGUCAUUUCUUUCCCAGAAGCCCCUGUUCAUUUCCUCUUUACUUUCCCUGAGCCUCACAUCCUGAGAAUUUUGCUUUUUUUUCUGAACUCCUCUUUCUUCCAAUUUUUUCCACUUCUGUGCCAUUUAUGUCUACGUGUGUGUGUGUGUGUGUGUGUGUGUGCGUUUCAAGUCCCUUCUUAUGAUUUAAUGGGGUUGGAGGGCUGGAGAGGUUUUCAUGUGCUUACUGUCAUGUUUUCAGCCAAAUUCCACAGGGCCUUGUAACAGGCUAACAUGAGCAGAUAAGCUCUUAAUUUUCAGUGACUUAUUUUAACUUUUUACUUCUUGCUCAUGUGUGGUAGUUCAGUACUCAUAGAAUAGAUCCUGACUGAGUGGCUGUCCAUGGGGUCAUUCAGGGAAUCAGGUUCCUUAGAGUUUUAUGGCUUUGUUCAUCUUUAAGUACCUAGAGUCCUCAUCAUUCAGUCAAGAUACAGAGUGUGAGGAGAUAAAUAAUCCAGAGAAGUCUUAUUGGAGGUUGUUGUAGGCACAGCCUGGAAGUGGUUGUCAUGACUUCUGCCCACAUUCCUCUGGGGUGGACCUCAGUCACUUCGACAUCCUUUGCUGCAAGGGAAGCUGAGAAGUGGUGUCUAGCUGAGUGCCUGGGGGAGAAGGGUGAAAGGAAAACAGGUUUGGUAAAUAACUAGCCAGUCUUUGUCACAGGUUUCCAAUGAAAGCAUGUGAGAAAAUCAGCUAAUUCUCUAGGUAUGGGGAAAAGAGAGCAUGGAUUUUGGUUAUUUGCCAAAUAAAUGCCCAUUGCCUUGCUUCCUUUUAAUUUUGACCUCUAUUACUAUCCCAUUCUUAGUGCAUAUGGUCUGGGUGGGAUUCCGUUUCCCAUUUAAGGAUUGGAGCAUGGGAACCAGGUCUUGUCGGGAAGAGCAUUGACUUUUCCUGUCCACAGUAAUUGCUUCUAGAACAGAACAGGCAUGGACCCAGUGAGAACCACUGCAGUGAGAUGCUUUGCUUUUUCUCAGUGGCUCUAGUUGGGCUCCAUGUAUGCCUUUGAACUAAUUCCUGUAGAUAAGGAGAUUAGAACCAGGGAGCAUGUGGGCCUGCCACUGCUGCAGCUGUCUUAACACCAAAAAGAGAACCUAGACCUGCUGAGGUCACCACAUACUACUUGAGAAUGAAGCCAACAGAACAGUAGCAAGGGGCAUGAUGGAGCAAAACCAGCUCCUCUUGCAUCAUGUGAGCCCGUUAAUCUGGCUAUGCCUAAAGUGAGUUAACCUGGUAUAUUAGUCUAUUCUCACACUGCUAGAAAGAACUGCCUGAGACUGGGUAAUUUGUAAAGGAAAGAGGUUCAAUUCACUCAGUUCCGCAUGGCCUCAGGAAAUUUACAACCAUGGCAGAAGGCACGAGAGAAGCAAAGGCAGGUCUUACAUGGCGGCAGGCAAGAGACAGUGAAGGAGGAAGAGCCCCUUAUAAAACCAUCAGAUCUCAUGAGAACUCACAAUCAUGAGACCAGCAUGGGGGAAACUGCUUCCACAAUGCAAUCACCUCCUACCAGGUCCCACCCUUGACACAUGCAAAUUAUGGGGAUUACCUUUCAAUUGAUGAGAUUUGCGUGGAGACACAGAGCCAAACCAUAUCAUUCUGCCCCUGGCCCCUCCCAAAUAUCAUGUCUUUUCACAUUUCAACAUGCCUUCCCAACAGUCGCCCAGAAUCUUAACCCAUUUUGGCAUUAGCUCAAAAGUCCACAGUCCAAAGUCUCAUCUGAGACAAGGCAAGUCCCUUCUACCUAUGAGCCUGUAAAAUAAAAAGCAAGUUAGUUAAUUCCAAGUUGCAGUGGGAGUACAGGCACUGGGUCAAUGUUCCUAUUCCAAAUGGGAGAAAUUGGCCAAAACAAAGGGGCUACAGGCCCCAUGCCAGUCUGAAACCAGGCGGGGCAGUUAUUAAAUCUUAAAGCUCCGAAAUCAUCUUCUUUAACUCUAUGUCUCAAGUUCAGGUCAUGCUGAUGCAGGAGGUGGGCUCCCACUGUCUGGGGCAGUUCUGCCCCUCUGGCUUUGCAGGCUACAGCUCCCCUCCCAACUGCUUUCAUGGCUGGAGUUGAGUGUCUGCUUUCAUGGCACACAGUGCAAGCUGUCAGUGGAUCUACCAUUCUGAAGUCUAGAGGACCAUAGCCCUCUUCUCACAGCUCCAUUAGGCAGUGUCCCAGUGGUGACUCUGUGUUGGGAGCUCCAACCCCCAUUUCCCUUCCGCACUGCCCUAACAGAGGUUCUUCAUGAGGGCUCUGCCCCUUCAUCACACCUCUUGCCUGGACAUCCAGGCAUUUCCGUACAUCUACUGAAAUCUAGGCAGAGGUUCCCAAACCUUCAUUUUUGUCUUCUGCACACCCACAGGACGAACACCAUGUGGAAGCUGCCAAGGCUUGGGGCUUACACCUUCCGAAGCAACAGCUUGAGCUAUACCUUGGCCCCUUUUAGCUACAGCUGGAGUGGCUGGGACGCAGGGCACCAAGUCCCUAGGCUGUACACAGCAGGGAGCCCAGUGCCUUGUCCAAGAAACCGUUUUUCCCUCCUAGACCUCUGGGCCUGUGAUGGGAGGGGCUGCCGCCAAGAUCUCUGUCAUGCCCUGAAGACGUUUUCCCCAUUGUCCUGGCUCCUCCUUACUUCUGCAAAUUUCUGCAGCUGGCUUGAAUUUCUCCCCAGAAAAUGGGUUUUUCUUUUCUACAGCAUCAUCAGGCUGCAAAUUUUUCAAACCUUUUUGCUCUGCUUCCCUUUUAAACAUAAUUUCUAAUUUCAGAUCAUCACACUCAAGUUUAAAGUUCCACAGAUCUCUAGGGCAGGGGCAAAAUUCUGCUAGUCUCUUUGCUAAAGCAUAGCAAGAGUGACCUUUGCUUCAGUUCUCGAUAAGUUCCUCAUCUCCAUCUGACCUGGACUUCAUUGUCCAAAUCAUUAUUAGCAUUUUGGCCAAAACCAUUCAACAAGUCUCUAGGAAGUUCCAGAGUUUCCCACAUCUUUCUUCUGAGUCCUCCAAGUCUCUAGUAAGUUCCAAACUUUCUGACAUCUUCCUGUUUUCUUCUGAGCCCUCCAAACUGUUCCAGCUCUAUCUGUUACCCAAUUACAAAGUUGCUUCCACAUUUUCGGGUAUCUUUAUAGCAGUACCCCACUCUCUGCAGUACCAAUUUACUGCAUUAGUCUGUUCUCACAUUGUUAUAAAGAACUACCCAAGACUGGGUGAUUUAUAAAGGAGAGAGGUUUAAUGGACUCACAGUUCUGUAUGGCUUGGGAGGCAACAGGAAACUUAAAAUCAUGGUGGAAGGGGAGAGAGAAGCAAAGGUAUAUCUUACAUGGCAGCAAGCAAGAGAGAGUGAAUGAGCAAAGGAGGAAAAUCCCCUUAUAAAACGAUCAGAUCUCGUGAGAAUCAUUCACUAUCACGAAAACAGCAUGAGGGAACUGCUCCCAUGAUCCAGUCACCUCCCAAUCACCACCCUUAACACUUGGGAAUUAUGGGGAUUACAAUUUGAGAUAAGAUUUGGGUGGGGACACAGAACCAAACCAUAUCAGCUGGUGAUUUUGCAGCUCUUCAGAUUCAUAAAUUACCCUUUGACGUAAGCUGAUUUGGGUUGGAUUUGUAUGACUUAAAGUGAAUACUGAUUUAUUAGACCAAGCAAAAAAGAGGAAAGAAUACUGGAUAAGGAAGGGAGUGGGGGUUUUAUUUGUUUGUUUGUUUUCCUGAGCUCAUCUUAUGUCACUUUGGUUGUGUGCCUAACAGUUUCACUCCCUUGUAAUACAUCAGACUUCCAGUCAAGAACCAUUUGGCAUACCCCUACCCAGGCACAUAGAGCUCUCACUAAAUUAUAAACCCGAAGCUGUUAAUUCUUCUCAAAGCUGAUCUCUCCUUACAGAGUUAUGGAAGGGAAAUGGAGGUGAAAUCACAUCCUCAGGCUUAAUUCCCUCUUUCAAGAUUGCCUGUGGUCCCUCCUGGAUGAUGCUUUCUUUUCCAGCAUCACUUCCCUGUUCCUAUCCUCCCCCAGGCUUGCAGACCAACUGUAACAAUCUAAUCACCCAUCCUGGAACUUUUCAUGUGCCUUUUCUUUUUUUUUUUUUUUUUUCAUGACUGUUUACAUUGCCUCUCUCUUUGGCCUCCUCUUACUGUCCUUGUCUACUGUGUUUAUUACAGUUUGCACAAUGCUCAACUCAAGUAUCACUAAGUUAAGCCUCUUUCAAUACUAUUGAGGCAUAAAGAAUGGCUCCGUCACCUGUACAUACUCUCAUUGUACUUGUUUCCAUGCCACUGAUAUAAUAUCUGUCAUGAGAAUGACCAUCUCUCUUGCUUUUCCCAGGACAGGGGGGUUCCCAGGAUGCUGGAUAUUCAUUUUUAAAACCAGGAAAGUCUUGAUCAAGCCAGGAGAAAUUUGUUGCCUUGCCUUCUACAUUGUAAUAGCUCUCAUUUAACAUGCCACUCGGUGCAAUGGAAUUUCAUUGAGACAGUGGAUAACAGCUUGAAAUUUGGAGGCAAAAUUCUUACCAAUCCUAGAUCCAUUUUGUACUAGUUGUGUGAUUGUGAGCAAGUGACCUAACUUUUCUAGGUUACAGUUUCAUCAUCUGUGUAGUGGAAUAGUAUGUGUUUUGUAGGGUUGUUAGCUAAUUAAAAGACAUCAUAAAUUAAAUCACUUCGUUUAGUGAUGGACACAUCUAUAACAUUGUCUAAAGCACACGAGUUUUGUGAAGAUUAUGUAGAGUACUACAUGCAAAGUACAAGCAGGACAGUGCCCAAAUCCUAGUAAGCAUCCAGUACACAGCUUUUGUUAUGGAUUGUUGUUAUUCACUUUUAAGUAUCUCUUGCCUAAAACAUAGUAGAUGCCAAAAAUACAAUUACACUCAGAGAAUACAUGUUCAUGGAGCAUAAACAAUGUUACUCAGAGUUUGUGAUAAGUGGGGCAAGCAAGUCAGUGAGAGUGAUUAGGAAAUAUUUUCGAUAAUUACUUGGUCUUUGAAACUUGAAAAAGCUGGAAUUGACUGCAGGAUUAGUUCCUUUUUAGAAACAGUUUGUUUUUUCUUGCAUAUUUAAACCAGACUUCACAAAUUUUCAUAGUUCGGAAAGAGAAAAUAUUUUCCAUGUUUAGGCAAGGUCAGUAUUGGUGCAUAACCCCUAAGUACAUAUUUUCAUUAUUUUUAUUAAUGAAAUAAAAGUGGCGCAUUUGGGGGACCAAAAUGCAAAUAUUUUGUCUUUCUUUUGGUUCAUAAGAAAGUGAAGGUUAGGGCAGUAGAAUCACUACUCCAUUAUUAAUCAUUAUUCCAUAAUGAUCUUGAGUUAAAAAAAUCAUAUGAUUUGUUGUUGUUGUUGUUAACCACAGUGACAUAUCCUCUCUACCUUUGGGCUGAACUUUUGUAUAUAAAAAUACUUUGUAACUUGCACACUUGUAUUAAUAUAAAUCUUGAGUGUCCAUGUUGCCUAUGCCUUUCAGUUUUGUCAUGGAAAUUUCCAGUGAGGACAGGUGUUGCAUGUGUGCUUAUGCUGAGAUGGGUCCAGUCUGGACAAGAAGACAAUCAAACAAAACAAUGAUAUGACUCAAAUCACCAAGUAUGUUUUGUAAGAUUUGAUUCUAGGCACAUUGUCAUCAUUUUAAGUUGUGCAAAUUUGUAUUGUUAUCCAUAUUAUGAUGGGUCUUCAACUAUUAAUUAUAAAUACGAAUUUUUUUGUCUUUAGUCACUCAUUUGAUUAGCUAUUAGCUAGAUAUUGAUUCUAGACUCCUUACAGAUUAGUGAAUUAAUUGGGAGUCCAAGCAUUAUUUUUAGUGUAUUUAAUUGGGUGAAUGACAGCUUUAUAGAGAAAGUGAUUACUUAAGUUGCAUAUCUAAUUCUUAGUAAAAAAUUAUAGUACAAACAAGGUCAUCUAGAAUUCUUGGAUCUAAGUAAUGGUAAAUUAAGAGUUGCUUUUAAUAUAAUAGUAUCUUUUAAAAAUGGAUAUCCCUGUAAAAUGUCUUCAUUUUCUGCUUAAGCAGGUGACUAAAGAUAAUUUACUUCUUGAUGACACGGGAUCACCAUGAUAAACAUAGUUUGGUGGUUUAGAAUAGAGUAUGGGCCUUGGAAUCAGACAGACCUGGUUUGAAUCCUUGUUUUGUCUCUUACUAGCUGUGUGAUCUCAAACACAUUCUUACUUUUCCCAAGGCAGUUUUUAAAAUCUGUAAAGUGAAGUUGAUCCUGCCUGUCUUACAGAUAGGCUGUGAACAUUAAUGGUAUGCAUUGAAGACUUUAGGACAGUGUGCAUGGCACAUUGUAAGCAUUAGGUAAAUGAACCGUAUACUACAAUCUUUACAACUUAUACAGAACGUAGUAUACUUAAAUGUUUUAUAUAUUUGUUGUUCAUUGUUUCAACAUUCUUUGCCACAUUCCUGUGACACUGGGGGAUGCAACAGGAUCCCAUCCAGUGCAGCUGAAGUGUUGAGACCGACACUGGUGACCUCCAUCUGCUUUCUGCUGCCUUUCAGAUUGUCAUAUUAUAAUCUUUCGCUUUGGUGAACUAGCCUUUUCCACUUGCUGUUUUCCACCAUUUGUGAACUGGAAAAAUAAAAUACACAAGCUGUUCAAACAUUCUUAGUAAGAGUAAACAGAUUCGGAGUGAGACUGUGAAGGGGCCUGUUUCUCCCCUCCCCGCCUUUUUUUUGGUUGUUGUUGUGAGAGAGUAAUGGUAUGGGUGUUUCACAUCCAUUUUCACUGUUCUCAGCUUUACCUCUCUACUUCCUGGCUGAGGUACUGAGAGUAAGAUAUCACUAUACCAUAGUGGAAAUAGAAAAUAACCUGCUUUGAUAAUAUUGUGACAUGUAUUUGUGAUAUGCUUGGCAGUAGCAUCAUGUUAGUGAAAAUUCCUGUGUUACAGUGUGGAAUGUUGGCUAUCUUACCUGUAGUACAAUAAACUUCAUUCAAAAUCCUGUGCUUAGAAUACAGCAUGAUCUUUAUGGUAUAAAGAGGUUUUCUUUUCUAUUUUUUUCCAGCACAUUUCAAGGUCUUACUAGUUACUAGAGUCUAACUCAAAAGCCUUAGUAUUUACCCUUUAUUUUCUUUUUUAAAUCCAGUGGUCAGAAUUCCCGAUACCAAAACAAUUAUGGAUACUAUUAAGGUGGCUGUAAUGCUUAUAUACGCACUGUGAGUUCAUUGAGAAUUCAUAGUUCUGUUAAUUCUACUCAAUUCUUAUAAUAAUUGAAAUUCACCAGCAUAUUGUUGUUUAUAGUAUGUGGUGUAAGUGAAAUUAAUACUUUUCUUUUAAACAUUAGUAUUUUCAGAGAAGAACCUUUUCCUGUUCUUCUGAAUUAAUGAAUUGUUACAAAUUUUUGUAGGUUUCUUAUAAUGUGGCUACUUAAAUCAACAUAUUAAGGUAAACUCUUAAGAAAAGAAACAUAAUAUAAUGUACUCCCCAAAAUAAUGAAUCCCAUGUUUUAGGUUGGUAUUUAGUCUCCACAGCUGGAAAACACUAUUUUAUGUGAUGUAUAGGAAAGGCUGGAGGCAGACUUGGUGAUUUAGAAUGACUCAGUGAUUCAUAUCCUGUCUCUACUACUUAUGUAUUUAGUAUAUAUACAAAUAUAUAUUAAAGUUAGUAUGUAACAUCAGACCAAGUCAUUUAACCUUUUUUAGCUUCAUUUUUCUCUUGUAUAUAAUGGAGGAAUUCCUGUAGGGUUGUGAAGACUAAAGUUACUUAAUUGUAUAUACACAUAGCCUUGUGCCAGGAAUAUAAUUAGACCAUCCCUAAAAAUGCUGUUUAUCAUGAUUUUACCCUUUCAAUGCAUUUAUUCAAUAUGAUGCUUGUGUUGUAGAUGAAAUAUGUGGAUGUUAUGAUUUACAAACUUGAAAUUUCAUUAUUUUAAAAUACUCUGUAAAGUGAUUUAUGUUUGCUCAUAUGCUUUUAUCUAUGGGAUAGACAAUGCAAUCCUCUCUGUGUGGAGACAGAGGAAGGCAACAUUUCCAUAGUGUGUUGUUUUAUGGUUGACUAUUACUGCGAGCCACUGUAUCAGAACUGAGAUGAGAUUAGCACUAUUUGAGAUUUUAUUUUGGAGAAAUGGUUUUGGCUAUGGUCAAGAAUCUUAUUUAUUAGAAAGAAUGAAUUACUGAAUAGGCUCUCAUCUGUAUUCUUUCUACUUCAGCUAUAGCCCAUCUUGCCAUCCUGUAAAAGAAAUGCUGACAGUGACAGAGGAGAAAUAUAAAAAUGUUUCCAGUUGCUUUCAGUCAAAUGUGAUUGAAAUUUUAUAAAAGAUUUACACAUUUUUUAUUUGUAAUACUGACAGUACUGGGAAAUGAAUUUCUGUUUACUCCAGAGAAUAGCAGUCACUUUAUAGGUGCUUUGAAUUUUAAAACUUAGCAAGCAUAACAAUAAUGACUGGUGUAUUAUUAACAUGCAUGUAAAAGGAGUUUAACAUAUCUGAAGAGAAACUGGUUAAUGUUAUUUUACUUCCUAUGUGUUUUUACAGCCUUUCAAGAAUGAAACAUUGGUAGUAAGUUUGUUUUGAAUGUUUCUCUAUUUCAUCUUUGUAUGUUGGUUUACUACCUAUUGUAUGGGAUUCAAAGAAUGUUUAUAUCAAAAACUGUUUUGUUUAGAGCUUAUCAUUAAACCUCAUUACUUAGAUGUUUUAAUUACUUUUAUAUGUUUCUUUCUGUAUUUCUAACACAUACAAUGAGAAUUUACUGUUUUCCAUUGUGUUUUACAUUUUUUUCUUCUGGUAAGUUACUAAGCUAACUCACAUCAGUAUCUUAAUUCCUGGAGAGAGACCCCCAUCCAUUUAUGUAUAUCCUAUAGAUCUGAUUAUGGCCUUGUUAUGGAAAUUGGCCUGACUACAGGCUUCUAGUCAUUCAUGCCCUAGUAUUCUCCCCUGUUAGGUAAUUUCCAAGAUGCACCCUCUACUAUAGUUUCUAAGUAAUUCUUCUGAGCACCAGACCAAGUAUUCAUGGAAGGCCUAAAAUAUAUACUUUCAAUGGAAAGGAUGGUAGAAAUUCAGCCAAUUCUGCUUUCUUGGGCUUUUAGAUAUUAAAAAGAGCUAUAGAAAUAUAAUUACACUGAUGGAUUUCACUGCUCUCAAUUGCCUGAAUUAUCAGGGUUGAGCAACUGAAGCGGGUGGAAGGGCUGUUUCCCUUAUAUCUGAAUAUAACAUAAUAAAUUGUCCAUCAAUAGGGACUAUUUGAGUUUGAUAUUGAUCUUUGAUGUUAUGUAUGCUGCAUUUCAUUGAUUAAAAGCAUGCAUUCUAGUUGGGUCUAGAUAUACAGUCUAAGUACAUGAUCUAUAGUUCAGAAUAGAGUAUCAUUUAUAUAGAAAUUUGCCCAUGGCCGUGUUGUAAUUGUAGCCCAUUGAUUGGCAUCUCCAAGGAGCUUGUGAGAAAUGCAGAAAUUUUUUCCUCACGCAGAUGCACUGUAUCAGAAUUUUCAUUUUAUCAGUUGAUUUUUAUUAAAGAUUGAUAGACAUUGAUUUGCAUUGUAUUCUUAACUAACUGAAACAACUGGUUCCCUGCUACGAAGCCUAAAUGUCAAGCAUAUACACAACCUGCUUAAUUGUAUAGUAAGGACCCAAUACUAUAGGAUGAAGGAUAGGUACAGUUGAGUUUGGCCAAAUGAUGAUCAGAGUCUAUAUAGUUUAAGGCGCAGAUACACAAAUUUUCAAAAAUAUGGGUAGAAUAUAGUCAAUAUGAAUGGAAUAGACAAUGCUUUGAAAAUCACUGGAGGGAGGCUUUAUUGUUUGUGAAAACAUGUUGUCAUCACUUUUUGCUUUAAGCCCUUGGUGGUGAAAUAACUCAAACCAUUCUUCCUUAUGCUGAAGAUCGAGAACCCCAAGUAUCACAUCUACCAUCCCACUCAUCAAUGUGAUUGGUCAGUCUUUGCUGAGGUCCUGCAUAGCCAGUUUUAAAGUUAGAGUUCUUGCAUAUACAUAUGAAAAGGCAUGUUACUUGUGCUUUCAAAGAGCUUUUUGCUUGGUGUAAAAAGAAAACUCAAAUUACAGUGUGAUGUGGAAUAUAAUGGUGGUAGUUUCAUCGAGAUGAUGGGAAAGAAUUGAUAAGAUAAAGUAGAAAGAUGAGCAGAAUUUUCAGAUUGGGUUUGGAAAGAGCACUUAAGAAAGAGGGUGGCCAGGUGGUGGCUCACACCUGUAAUCCCAGGACUUUGUGAGGCCGAAGUGGGCAGAUCACUUGAGCUCAGGAGUUUGAGACCAGCCUGGUCAACAUGGCAAAACCCCAUCUCAAAAAAAAACAAAAAAAUACAAAAACUAGCUGGCGUGUUGGUGCCCACCUGCAGUCCUAGCUACUCGGGAGGCUGAGUUGGUAGGAUCACUUGAGCUAGGGAAGUUGAGGCUACAGUGUGCUGUGAUCCUGUCACUGCACUCCAGUCUGGAUGACAGAGCAAGACCUUGUCUCAAAAAAUAAAUAAAUAAAAUUAAGAAAGAGGGUAUAGUAUGUACAAUGGCCAUGGGCUUAUGAGGAAAAAUGGCAAGUUUGGAGAAUGCCAAAGGUAUGAGUGGACGCUAGGGGUAUGGGAAGGUGGCAAUAGGGCCUUCAUUUACACAGUUUCAUAGACUAGAAUGUGAAUGUUAUCCCCAGAGUUGGACCACCAACAAGCAGUGACUGUGAUUGUUGCAUCAUGGCUUUGUGCAAAGUAGCAUCUCUAGCGAAUGGGACAAAUUGGGGAAUAUGAGGGAAUUGGGAGAUAUUCUUUAUGCUGUAGAAAGCCACUGCAAGAUUUAUAUGACAAGGUAUACAGUGCUGAUCUGCUGACCAAUAUAUUUUCUGGCAUCAUUCCGUGUUUCUCUCUUGUGAGUGAGGUGCAUUCCUUUGCUAAUAACAUUUGCUGUCCUCAGACAUUAUUAAAGGAAAUUUAAUGCUGUUUGACAACAUUUCAAGUAGUAGCCAUUGAUAUUGUCAUGGACAUUUAUUGUUAAUCACAGGAACAAGUUUCCUUUUCUAACAGCAAAAUCUCUUCCACUGUUUGCAGUCUUGUGUGAUGAUGAAACCUCAGCCCACCCUCCUAAUAGGCAGUGGACCAUGAGGCCUCUCUGAUGAGCCUUCAGCCAGGCUCUUCUCCUUGCUCCAGUACAUCAUGCAGGCAUGUGACCUAAGUUGCAAUGAUCAGACCCUCUCCUCAUACGUAGAAUCUUGGGCUUAGUAACAUAAGGAUGAAGAAAUGGUUAGUAGAUGUAUGCUUUUUACUGUGUCAGUGUCCUGGCCCCACUGAACAUGGUGUGUGGUCCAAUAUUAAUGGUAUCUCUACUGGGGGUUUUGGAGCUGCUUUGUCCUCUAGUUCUUCCUUCUAUUCCAUGCGCUCUCCAUAUCCUUUUGAUAGUCUCCUUUUCCCAAAGUUGGUUAUUCUUUCUUGGAACCAAGGAACUAUAAAGAGAAAUGGAGGUUCUUCCAGGUAACCCUGUUUAUCCUCUUAGCUUUCUGUUAGGGACAUCCACAGCACGAGACACACAAGUUAGCUUUUCAGGGUGCCUCUUGAGGCCUGUCCAGGAAUUUGGAAAAUUCAUCCUCUUAAACAGCCCAUGGCAUUUUCCACAGUUUAUGGUAAGUACUCUUAUCUCAGUAUUCUGCAGAAUGCAGAAAGGUACCUUGUAAACUUGGGGUAUAAAUCUCUCUAUUGGUUUUCAAGUUGUGGUGUAUAGCUUUAUUCAAAGGGAAUUCUAACAUUUCAUACAACCGCAGCUGCCAUGUUAUUUCUUUUAAAAGCUUGUGCCUUCUCUGAAUAAUUCAUAUUGUCCAGUGCCUUCAGAUUGUUUCAUAAGAUCAACACCUAAAAAGUCCUUUCUUGUUCUAGCUAAUACUUAAAGACUCUUUUGCAAAUGUGUUUCUAGAAAUUGUUAUCACAGUUAGGGUGGGCAUUUAGCUUUUUGUGCCUAGCCUGUAAACUUGGUCUUAUUAACUUUGGGAACCAUGAGUCUUGGUAUUUAUGCAGUGAGACUUAAAUCUUUCUCGAAGGUGCUUUAUAGUAACCUGCAUGUAAAGCCUCUAACUUGGGCCUGGCACUCAUCAUUGGGUUGGACCCCAAUCCUGAUGAUCUUCAAAUCCUCUUUCAUACAUAGCCAUCACCACUAAAGUCUUAUUCAGCUAAUGUUAGAAACAAAGCAUUGCAGGAGGCCUCAUAUCUAGUAAAUGCACUUUCAUACCCAGUUUACUGUUAUCCUCCAUAAUUAACGUGAGGCAUAACAGAAAAUAAUCAUAGACCAGGCAUACAUCUCAAAGCUUAGACAUGUUAUGAAUGUCACUCCACAUACCAGCUCCAAUCCAUCAUUCCUGUCCUCAGCUUGGAAGUGGAGGAGGGGAGACGUGUUUAUGGGACUAAAUAUAAACUCUGUGGGGUAAUUGCUACAAAAUGUCAUCCUCAGAAACACCUGGGAGCUUUGGAAGAAAAUAAAAUUUCACAGCCCCACGCUAGGUAAUACCGAAUCAGAGUCUCUGGGAAUGAGUUUUAGGAAACUGUAGUUGAAUAGGCUCCCCAUGUGAUUCUGAUGUUCAGCCAGGUUUGAGCGCUAAAGCAUGUUCUGUGGAACACUAAUUCUUCUAGGUAGAUAUAAAUAGGAUUCCCUUUAAAAGUGUUCUUAACAAAAACAGAGGAAAUUCAGGAUUUUAAACAGGUUUUCUAACACGAGAAUUUUUCAGAAUCUUUAUGUGCAUUGUGAAAUGCAUGUUUCUGACUAUGGAACAAUCUUGCUUCUCUAUCCCCCCUGCCAACUCCCUACCCAACACAAAGACUCUUUACUAAACAUCUAAUGUUGCAGAUUUCAGCCCUGGCUCCUCCUUAGAAUAAUCCGGUUAAUCGAUCGAUCUGGGGUUGGGGGUGGGUUCUGUGUGGGAGAAACAAACUCAAAGUGUGUUUUCUAUUCUCUCACUCAAAAACAAUCAAUAGAGAAGAUUUUUGUGACCAAAUUUGUGGGGGAAUCACCCACACAUCAAGCAAGCAAUCAGUUUUCCAGCAGACACUAACUCAGCGUCCUCUAAUUCAGUUCAGUACUGACACUCUCUACUUAGAGAUAGUCUCAGAUCACAGAGGUUGAGGGCUCAGUCCCACAAGACUGUCCCCUACUCCCAAUGCCACAGGCAAGCCUCUGGUUGCCUGUUUUAAUGGCAUUUCUAAAACAGACCAGCUAUAAAUUGGUGUUCCCGCAACCUCCUCCUUGGGUUCAGUUAAUUUGCUAGAGCUUCUCACAGAGCUCAGGGAAACACGUUUACUGGUUUAUUAUAAAGGAUGUUACAAAGGAUACAGAUGAAGAGAUUCAGAGGGUGAGGUAUUGGGGAAAGGCCCCACACUGGGCCUUUCAUGCCCUUUCUGGGCACACUACCCUCCAGGAACCUUUUGUGUUAAGCUGUCUGGAAGUGCAUCUGAACGCUGUCCUUCUGCAUUUUUCUGGGAGCUUCAUUAGGUAGGCAUGAUUGAUCAAAGUAUUGGCCAUUGGUGAUCAACCUCACCCUCAGUCCCUCUUUCCUUCCAGGAGGUUGGGGGAGGGGGCUGAAAGUCCCAACCCUCUAAUUAUAUCUUGGUCUUUAUGGUGACCAGCCCCCAUCCUGAAGCUACCCAGUAGCUGCCAGCCAUUCAUCCGCUAAUUAGCAUACAAAAGAUUUUCCUUUGGAGGUCCCAAGGAUUUUAGGAGUUUUAUGUCAGGAAAUGGGGUGUAGGACAAAUACAUAUAUUUUACCACUUCAUGGGCUAAUGGAAUAUUUUAAAAUUUCCCGGGUGAUUUUAUUAGACACGCAGGGUUUAGGACCACAGAUGCGAUGUAAUGUUCUUUGGAAGACAUUCUGGAUGAUUUAUUUAUUUAACAAUGUGUCCCACAUCACCCAGAUUUUUUAGUUUCACAUCUGUCAGGUGGUUUUACUCAACUUACAUAUGUAUCAUCCUAUGUUUAGAGCUUGUUUUUAAAUAUCUUUUUUUCUGAUUAUAAUAAAAACUUUUUCUUAGAAAAAACACCCCAGCUAUUACAGACACUCUUAGAUAAAAAUGCAUUGGUUGUCUAAGUGAAUUUUAAUCAUAAUGAGUAAUAUUAAUUGAACAUUUAUAAUGUACCAAGGAAGUCACUAAAUGUUUUUAUUAUAUUAUCUCAUUUAAACCUAUAAUAGUCCUGUGAGCUAGAUGCUGUGAUGACCCCUGGGUCCUAAAUGAGAAAACUGAGAAUCAGAAAGAGUAAGUAAUUUGUCUCAGGUCAUGCAGCUAAUAAAUGGCAAUACUGAUAUCAUAUCAGAUCCCAGGUAUACCUGAUUGUGAGCUAAAGCUCUUAACCAAUUUGGAAUCCUGGUUAAGACAGAGGCUUUUAUGUUUAGUGAUCAGUGUAUGCUUAAAACCCCUUAGUAUGUACAUGUUACUUUGUGAAGCACAUUUUAUUGCAAGGAAGGUGAAUCUUCAUAAAUGACAGGGGUUUAGGAAAGUAUUCCAAAUGUUAAGAACCAUUUUAAAAUGGGAAGAUUUUCAACCAAAUAUUUGCAUAUGAAUGUAAACAGAAUUUUUGUAGUUAUAGUAGAUUGGUAAUUUGUGCAUGUAAGUUAUAUAUUAUUCAUUAAUCUGAAUGUAUUUGAAUAUUCCAAAUUCACUGUUUACAUAUAUUUUUCCUACCGAUAGGCUUCCAAAUGUUGCUAAGCUUCCAGAAAUAUUGAGUUUGAUAGAUUUUUUUGGUUCCUCUGGCCAGAAAUUUAAACAAAAAGAAAAGAAUGAUUUGGACUACUGGCAAUAAAACUCAGUGAAGGGGAUUUAUGUACGGGUCCGAAUGCAUGCUUAUUAGUCACUCAGAACAUGAUGUUUCAUUUUAAAAGUACAUGCCUUUGCAUCUUGUUAUGACAUUUAGAAAAAGUUUUCAGUUGCAUGUCUUUCAUUUUGCCAGAGAAGAUAAAUUGACUAAUAUGUAAAUGACAUUACAGGGUCCAAGUGUAAUGGUUAAUUUUAUAUGUCAACCAGGCUAGGUCUGGAUAUUUGGUCAAACAUGUCUGGAUGAUGCUGUGAAGAUAUUUUAAAGAUGAGAUUAACAUUUAAAUCAGUGGACUUUGAAUAAAGCAGAUCCAUAAUGUGGUGGGCCACAUUCAGUCAGCAGAGGGCCUUCAGAAAAAAACUGAUCUCCCAGGAGAAAGAAUUCUGCUAGCAGACAGCUUUUGGUCUCUGGCUGUGACAUUAACUCUUCAUUGCUUGUCCAGUCUGUUAACCUGCCCUGCAGAUUUUGCACUUGCCAACCUCCAUAAUCACGUAAGCCAAUUCCUUGGUGUGUCUCUUUCUUUCUGUCUCUCUCUCCGUGUAUACAUCUAGUCCAUCCUAUUGGUUUUGUUUCUGUGGAGAACCCUGACUACUACACCAAUAUUCCUUAUUCUCCCUGUAUGAGAAAGUUUCUCUAGCUGUUUUUAGAAUAAUUUUAUUUGGAUGUCCUUACCCGCAAAAUCAACUGUUAGACUUUUGCAGAAUGAUUAGUGAUGGAUCAUACCAAAUACUGCCAUCUCCAACACUAUUGAUGUUUCCCCAGGCAUUGGGCAAUUUCAUAGAUGCCAUAUAGAGUAAAUGGGAACACAGAAAGUUCAAAGAUGGAAUUUGUUACUCCCUGGAAAUUUGUAGUGGUAAAGGUUUCCAGGUGUGGCUUUUGUCUUCCAGUCCAAGUAGGAUAAUUUAGAGAAAUGGGAAAAUAAUCUCUUUCUAGAAUCCACUUCAUUUUUCCAUUUAACCUACAGGUAUCAAGUGCUACUAAGCCGUAGGACCAAGCUAGAUCCUAUGGGUAGAAAAGAAAAGAAGUGGAUAUGGAACUUGCCAUCAUAGAGCUUAGGGUGUGGUAGGGGUUACCCAAAAAGAGUUAAACAAUUAAUACUUUAAAAAAUUAUAAACUGUAUAGGGGCUCUGAAGGAGAAAAGGAAAGUGCUGAGAUAGUGCAUAAUGUGGGCAGGAUCUAGUGUAGGUGGCAGAGUCAAGAAAGGCUUCUUGGUAAAUGUGAAUUUUGAGACCCCCAAACUUGAGAUGGAGCUAGCCAUGCAAUAACCAGGGAAGAAAGUUCCAGGCAACGAAGACAGCAUGUAAGGGGCAGUAGGUAAGUAAGAGCUUGACUCAUAACCUGAUUUAAGUUUUAAUGUACAAACAAUCAAGUUGUCAUGGGUCAAGAAAGCCUUAGACUAAGCUGAGUGAAGGGGGCUCUAAAUAGAAUCAUAUAGGAGAAAUAACACUGGGAAAAUGAGGAUAGUUUAGCUGGAUUCUACUUUGAGAGUAUGAUAAAGGAGAAACAUUAGUUUCACACUUUACUAGUUUUUAAAUAUGUGUAACUUCCAUAUUAUUUAAACUAUAACAUGAGGCAUUUAGGUUAUAUAUAUAUAUAUAUAUAUAAAUAUAUAUAUAUAUAUAUAUAUAUAUAUAUAUUUUUUUUUUUUUUUUUAUGCAGAGUCUCACUCUGUCGCCGAGGCUGGAAUGCAGUGGCAUGGUCUCCACGGACUGCGAGCUCGCUUCCUGGGAUCAAGCAAUUCUCCUGUCUCAGCCUCCCGAGUAGCUGGGAUUACAGGUGCACACCACUAUGCCCAGCUAAUUUUUGUAUUUUUAGUAGAGAGGAGGGUUCUCCAUGUUGAUGAGGCUGGUCUUGAACUCCUGACCUUAGGUGAUCUGCCUGUGUCGGCCUCCCAAAGUGCUGGGAUUACAGGCAUGAGCUACUGCGCCUGGCUGAUAAAUAAUUUUUUAAGUAUGCAUGUGACUCUCACGAGUGUGGACUGCUAGCUAAGGCUGGCUCAUCAAUAUUUGUCUAGAGAUCUUAAAACUGAGUGAAAUACUGUCUAAGUGAAUUUUAAUCAUAAUGAGUAAUAUUAAUUGAACAUUUACAGUGUACCAAGGAAGUCACUAAAUGUUUCUAUUAUCUCAAUUAAACCUAUAAUAAUCCUAUGAACUAGAUACUAUGAUGGCCUCUGGGUCCUAGAUGAGAAAACUGAGAAUCAGAGAGAGUUAGUAUGAGGCUCCUCACACUUUGGGAGGCUUUCUCUGCAUCUGAAGCCACUUGAAAGUCUAGACUCAUUGACUUUGUGAAUUUUAAUGACUUCCUUCCUCCCUCCCUUCCUUCCCUCCCUUCUUCCUUCCUUCUCUCCCUCCCUCUCUUCUUUCCUUCUUUUUUCCCCUUCCUCUCUUUGUUCCUUCCUCCCUCUUACCAAAUGCUAGUACAGCACUGGAUAUGGUGAAUAUAUCAUUUCAGGCAUAAGAAAUUAUAUGCCGUGUAAUCCCAGCACUCUGGGAGGCCGAGGCGGGCAGAUCACGAGGUCAGAAGUUUGAGACCAGCCUGACCAACAUAGUGAAACCCCGUCUCUACUAAAAAUAGAAAAAUUAGCCCGAUGUGGUGGCACGUGCCUGUAAACCCAGCUACUCAGGAGGCCGAGGCAGGAGAAUCGCUUGAACCUGGGAGGUGGAGGUUGCAGUGAGCCGAGAUCACACCACUGCACCCAGCCUGGGUGACAGAGUGAGACUCCGUCUCAAAAAAAAAAAAAAAAAAUGAAGUUGUGUGCACGGGGACCCAUAUCCUCCAGUCCUAUAGAAUUGUAAGUUGGUUACUAUAGAACUUGUGCUGUAUUUGGAACCUUUCACUGAAGAAUAUAAGCAAAUGUCAAACCUGUAAUUUGUCAGAGUUUCCAUUUCACAAUCUGAAGAACUGAAGUGUACAACCUUCACUCUGCAUUGUUGAAAUGAAGAGAAAGAGUUAAAGGUAAUUAUCCAUAUAAUUUGAAAGAAAAAAUGUCUCCUUCUGCUCAAGAAGUAGGGUCUGAUACCUUGAUUAAUUUGUACUGGUUACUAAUAUUUAAUUUCCCUGGAUAGUGUCUGAACUUUCCAUUUCAGUUUGCCAUUGUACCCCCUUUGUAUUUUAAAAUUAUUUUUCUUUAUCACACCUGUAAUCCCAGCACUUUGGGAGGCCGAGGUGGGCGGAUCACGAGGUCAGGAGAUCGAGACCACGGUGAAACCCCGUCUCUACUAAAAAAAUACAAAAAAAUUAGCCGGGCGUGGUGGCGGCGCCUGUAGUCCCAGCUACUCGGGAGGCUGAGGCAGGAGAAUGGCGGGAACCCGGGAGGCGGAGCUUGCAGUGAGCUGAGAUUGCGCCACUGCACUCCAGCCUGGGCGACAGAGCGACACUCCAUCUCAAAAAAAAAAAAAAAUUAUUUUUCUUUAAAGGUUAUUUGUCUAUGAUUGUGCAUUUUAAUAGUAUGAAAGGGUACCUGGUCAAAACUGUUUGCCUUUUGUCACUUUCUGCUAACUCUUUUCCCUAGAGACAAUGUUACUAUUAUUUGUUUAUCAUUUCAGAGAUCUUUAUUGUUAUAUGGGCACAUAUAACUGAUUUUGUCAGUUAAAAAAAUCUGAAUGCUUACUAUAAAAAAUGAUGGCAUGGAAUAUUUUUCUUCACUUAAAGAUGAAUCUUAGAUGUCAGUCUACAUUAAUCUAUAUGUAGCUAACUCUUCCCUGCGAAGAGUAUUUAUUCCUUUGUACAAAGGCCAUAAUACUAGAACUUGCUCAUAAGAAUUUAUGUUCUUUACAGACUCUUGCUAUGAUAAACAAUAUCUUUGUAAACAUGUGUGAUUAUAUCUGUAGGAUAAAUUCCUGAAAGAAGAAUUGGAAUUUUUUUGGUCAAAAAUACUGUAUUGUACAUUUAAAAACUUUUAUAAUUAUUUCCAGAUUGCCCUGCAAAGAAAUUAUCAUAAUUUACAUUCUCAAAACAAGGUUGUCAUAAUGUUUGAGUUGAUGCAGUAGCUCCUUAGCAAUUAAUAGACGUUCAUUUUACAAUCUGUCAACAUUUGCAACUUUCACGAAGCCUCACAAGUGAUCGUGUACCCAGGUAAAACAGCUUAUGUUAGACAUUCUUGUGCAAGGUUUAUGGUUGGCUGUUGUUCUUAAUCCUUUCCAGUUAUAAGAGCUCAUUGAAUGUCUCAGUUCAAGGUUGCCAUGUUAUAUUAUGAGACAUUGGGUACUGUCGGUGAGACUUGGCAUGACUGGACGAGCCAUUCUGAUCUUUGAAUUACACAGCAAGUAGAAGCCAGGACAGUAUGUUCUUGACUUAAGGCAUCCUCAGCAAAGUGAUAACCUAGCUGAUCUUCUGAGAACCCUCAGCCAGACACAGUGGAGUUUAUGGUAAAUUAUAGCUCUUGUUGAGCAUUGACUAUAUGCCUAGCACCCUUGCAUAUGAUUUCUAAUCUUUACAACAACCCUCCAAAAUGGGAAUAACUAUCCUCACUUUACAAUUUUGGAAAUUUAAGUUCAAAACGGCUGAGUGCAUUUCUCAAGGUCAAGGUCACAUAACUAAUAAUUGGCAGAGCUAUCUCCCUCUGCCUGCUUCCAGAGGAGUUUUUCCUUUUAUUGCAUCAUUGCAAUUGACCAUCAGAAUCACUUGGCUUUACUAAUUUUUUAUGCAUUAAACAGGUUUUUCUGGUCAGUAUCCAGGCAAAUUUAGGCAGUUCUUGUUUGGAAGGGUCCUUUCCUUUGGUUGGUCCAGCUUUUGCACCCCUGUACUUAGAGGGAUGCUCAGAUGCUCAGAUGUCUUUGCUACUGCUGUGUCCAGCUGUGGUGUAUCUUCCCAUGCUGACCCUACUCUCAUGUUUCUGAACUGACAUCUCGCAAGAUUAAUUGAGAUGCUGUAGUUUUCUAGCGCUACACUGGCUGUAAUUAGUCGCUGACAUAUGAUGAUUUAUUAUAGGGGAUUCCUUUAGAAAUUUACUUUGUGUUUUGGGACUAAGAAAUGAUCGUUAGAGUUUCAGACUUACAGCUCUUGUCCUGCACCACUUAACUGAUCAAAACUAUGUUUGGGAUGACCAGGCAGCUUGACAUCAUAGCACUGGUCAUCCUGACUCUCUAAGUAAAACUGAAAUGUGUGGCAAAUUAAAAGCAGUGAAGAUGGUGCAUGGCUAAAUUAAUUCAUCUUGAUUAGGCCCUGGUGAAUUUUUAAAUAUAUAAUCAGAUGUGAGAAUUUAAGAUGUGGGAUAGUCAAAGCCAAGAAUCCAGGAAGACUUCUAGCAAUUCCACAAAGACAAAAAGCAAAGAUGCCAGAAGACUGUGGCCAGGCUUGCUUGUGGAAUGAAAAUAAGGGGAAAAAAAUCACUUACAAUAGAUUAACAGUAUACCCUGUCAAAGAGUGUGCCAGAAGUCACGUAAAAUUCCCAACCCACUGACAGAGAUUUUGGAGAGGUGAUGAGAGUGAGGGGAAGGGAUUAUCUGAAAAAUAUGAACAAGGCAGUAGUGAGGAAUAAGAUGCCAGCAUCAACUUCCGCUGUCACUUGUUUUCUCAACGGUUAGCCAUGCCACUAAGGUCAACUCAGUAUGUUAUUAAAAUGGGCGGUUUUAGGUAAUGAUUACUUUCUUGGCAGAUAGAGGAUUCUUUUAUCUUUGGGGUCAUGCAUUUUUAAAAGCCUUUGUCUGCAUAGAUUUAUUUAAAACACACACACACACACACACACACACACACACACACACACCCCCUUAAGCAAGGUAUGCUGGCUCACACCUAUAAUCCCACACUUUGGGAGGCUGAGGCGGGAGGACCACUUGAGCCCAGGAGUUCAAGACCAGCUGGAGCAACAAAGUGAGCUCCUUGUCUCAACAACAACAAUGACAACAACAACAACAACAUCUGGGCAUGGUGGUGCAUGACUGUGAUCCCAGCUACAUGGGAGGCUGAGGCAGGAGGUUCCCUUGUGCCAGGAGGUUGAGGCUGCAGUAAGCUAUGUUCAUGCUACUCUACUCCAGCCUGGAAGAGAGAGUGAAAAACAACCAACCAACCAACAAAAAAGCAGCUUGAUUGAAGUGUAGUUGAUGUACAAAAAUCUACACAGAUUUAAUGUAUACAAUUUGCGGAUUUUAAUAUAUGCAAAGAUGCAUGAGACAAUCAGUACAAUUAAGGUAAUAAAUAUAUCUAUUAUCUCCAGAAGUUUCUUCCUGCCCCCGCUCCAUGUUUUUACUGGUAAGAUCACUUGACAUCUACUUGCUUGACAGAUUUUUAAGUGCAUAAAACAGUGUUGUUAACUAUAGGCACUAUGUCGUGUAGCAGAUCUCUAGCACUUAUUCAUCUUGCAGAAUUGAAAUUUUAUACCCUUUGUACCCUUGAACAAUAACUCUCCAUUUUUCCUUCCUCUACAGGCUCUGGAAGCCACCAUUCUACUCUUUGUUUCUAUGAGUUUGACUAUUUUAGAUACCUUAUAUAAGUAGAAUCACCCAGUAUUUAACCUUCUGUAACUGCCUUAUUUCACUUAGCAUACUGUCUUCCAGGUACAUGUAUGUUGUCACAUAUGGCAGGAUUUCCUUCUUUUUCAAGGCUGAGUAACAUUCUAUUCUCUGUGUGUGUGUGUGUGUGUGUGUGUGUGUGUGUGUAUAACAUGCCACGUUUUCUUUAUUCAUUUAUUGAUAGAUAUUUAGGUUGUUUCCAUAUCUUGACUACCGUGAAUUAAGUAAACUCCAAUGAUCAUGGGAGUGCAGAUAUCACUUCUAGAUCUAAAUCUUUGACAUCUUGACUUCAAUUCCUUUGGGCACAGAUUUCUAUGAAGAUUUCUUUUUUCUUUUUCUUUUUCUUUUUUUUUUUUUUUGAGACGAGUCUCACACUGGCACCCAGGCUGGAGUUCAGUGGCACCAUCUUGGAUCACUGCAAGCUCUGCCUCCUGGGUUCACCCUUUCUACUGCCUCAGCCUCCUGAGUAGCUGGGACUACAGGCGCCUGCCACCAUGCCCGGCAAAUUUUCUGUAUUUUUAGUAGAGACGGGUUUUACCGUGUUAAGCAGGAUGGUCUCGAUCUCCUGACCUCGUGAUCCGCCCGCCUCAGCCUCCCAAAGUGCUGGGAUUACAGGCGUGAGCCACAGCACCAGGCCUUCUAUGAAGAUUUAUAAGUUGCUCAGUUUUUAUUUCUGGUGUGUGUGUGUGUGUGUGUGUGUGUGUGUGUGUAUGUGUGUAUGUGUGUGUGUUUUAAUUUUAAAAACCCUGUCAUAUUUAGGAUAUACCUCGUGAUGAGUGUGAUCAGCACUAAUUGUCACUCUGUUAUACUAAAAGCUCUUUCCGUAGUGUGUCUUCAUUGCAAGCAUCCAUUGUGUAUGGAAUCCUGAAUACAGUUAUUUGAAUGUCUGAGUAUUAAACAAUUAACUGUCUUUACAGAAUGUCCUCCGGGGAACAUAGUUUUUCCUUAGGGACCCUUGGGAUCUCUAACCGCUUAAAAUCUAGAAGCUCUUAUGUGAUAGGAUGGGAAAUUAAAAAAUAAAUCUCUACUAUAUGUUAGGAUGUCCAUACUGCAUAUAGCUCCUUAAGAUAAUGGACUAUGAUUCUAUCUUGUCUCUGCGCCCAGUACAUGGCACAUUUCAGGGUGUCACAGAUUUCCUAGGAUUAAAAUGCUUAGUAAAUAUAUGAAUGAAUUCUAAUUUUAGUUUCUUUAUCUGGCACCUUUUCUUGUACUUUCUGAGCAAUAAGAAGUAGGUAUCUGGGUUUCUAGUAGAUUUAUGCCAUAUAAUUAAGAAAUAUUGAUUUAAUAAUUUUUGUGUCCUGUGAACUUUAUUUAAUCAUUAGCUAAUAAGAUUUAUUGAGCAUCUUGCAGUUCUGUAGCCCUGUGCUUGAUGGUGUUAGCUCCUUAGCACGUAAUUGUUUUGACUAGAAUGGUAAUUUAAGGUAAUUUGAUAUACAAAAUGGAGUGCUAUGUAUGGCAAAGUUGAGAGGGGGUGAGGAGAAUAUAACUUCAAACCUGUUUGAAAACUCAUCAAGUAAUAUUUUUCUUACUUUAAAUGUGCUUUGGCCUCCUUUGUGUGCAAGCAAUAGAGACCUAUUUAGGCUCCUUUAACUACUGGGGGUUUAUCAAAAGGUGAAAUAUAGAAAUAAAGAGACGAGAAAUACUGUCCACAUGGGAGAUUCUGAUGUGAAUUCUGGGAAAGCUGCACAAGUGUGGCACACCUGGACCUCACCUAGAUGGAGGGUGGUUCGAAACUAGAAGGUCCUUUGUGACUUUUGUCUGAUGAGGAGUCCUAGCAGUUUGAGGAUCCAGUUUUCAUAGUUACAUAGUUAAUUUAGUUUAAUGACUUAUUCUGUCUUUUUCAUCUUUGUGGUUUGCGUUUUUCUCCUUUCUCAAUGAAUUGCUAGCUCUCUUCUCAAGAGAAGCCUGGAUUGCUUAAGUUACCAUCUUCCCACCUUUGUGGGCAGUGCCCUUGCUGGAGUCCACCUGAUACCCUGUGGAUCAGCUGCCCUUUGUCGGGUUCCCAUCACAGCCCCAAUGUGCUGUGGGUGAAGGGGUGGCCAGGGUGUUGAGAGAGAGCCAAGUCCAUCAGAGAACUUUCAGAAGUACCUUGCUGUGAAUCAUCCUUCACAGCCUAGUGGGUGCCGCUCCUCCCUUUUAUUCAAUUUUUUAAUAAACUCAAUAUUUGAUCAAAUUAAGUGGAGGGAGGGAGGAUGGAAUAACAUGCUCCUGAUAUAAUGGAAAAUUCAGGCUCAUUGAACUUGUGUGAUGUGCCACAAUCCUUUUAGAACAAGACCGUGAUUGAAACUAGUCUCUUUUCUCUAUUACUUUUUUGAUUGUUUUAAAAAAAAUCAAGAAUAUUUCUAAAAUAUAAAAAAAAUUACAGGAGAGAUAAUUUGAGUAUCUUCACUUUUUACACUCCUGCCAAGAAUGCCCCACAACCCCACCCAUUACAGAAGGAUCAGAUUCCAUAUUGGAAAUAUAUGCCAAUUUCAAUUUAGCUGCUCAGUACCAAGAAUUCUUGCACCUAUGAGAUGCUAAAGGUUUGAACUAAAUGGAGCCACAUUCAUCAUUGUUGUAGAAAUCUGCCAGUGUUUAAAAGGUGCUACAGGGAACCUUUAAGUCAUGCACCAAAUUAAAAGAUUGCAAGCUCCACUGGUGUAGUCAAAAGCAAGCUCAAAGCUGAGUGGCAUCAAACCAAGAGUAGAAGAUAACUUGUUACUGAAUUUUGUUCUUCCUCUGAAUGCCACUCUUUCAAGCAGAGCGAGGAAAAUAUGAAUUUUGUGUUGUUAAAAGAUGUUUAUUUCCACACCCUAAUUUAUGUUUCAAACUGCAGGCUUUUGCAGAGAGUGUUUCUCUGAAACUUUUAAAGAAAGUGACAUGUUACUACAUGGGAAGAAAAGAUAGAGCCUGGUUGGUAAUGAUUAUACAGUCAGGGCUUUAUCUGCUUGCAGAUAAUUUGUGGCUUAUUUUUAACCGUCUGCCAGUUUCUUUUCUCAUUGUUACAUUUACCUGCUGAUUGCAACCCUGAGCCAAUCAGUCACUGGUGAGCAUUUGGUGAAUUCUACUUUUUUAAACUGGCCAAAAGAAAACACAUAUUUCCAGAAUGGACACAGUGAUACUAGCUAAUAUUUAUUGAAUACUUAUUAUGCAGUAGAUUCAAUAUUUUAAAUUUAACAUUUACAGAAACCUCACCAUAGCAAGAAUUAUCAUUACUGUUUUACUGAUGAAUAGGGUGAGGCUUAGAAAGGUAAGUAACUUGUCAAGGUCUUAAAGGUAGUCAAUGUCAGAGGCAGGGCUUGGAUCCAGGGGAAACCUGGUCAAUUUUAAUCCUGCACUGAGAGGUGAUCACAAUCUGAAGACUGUGAUCGACACUAAGACAGAUUUUGUCAAACAAGCUGGUAUCAUGAGGAAGUCAGUUUGGAUGAUGAUGGUAUCCCAUAACAUGUCUCAAGAAGAACUUAGGAUGUUUAGCUUAUGGUGGUGUAAAUUCAGUGCAAGGGGAUGUAAUAGGUGUCUUCAUUUACAUGAAACAAUUUCAAGCGAAAGAUGACUUAGAUCUGCUUUGCAUUUGCACAGGGGUGAGAUGUAAGACAUAUUAAAGAAAACCAUAAAGAGCCAACUGAAUGAAAUGAUUCAUCAAUAAAUGUGUUUCCUCAACGUAUAGUGAGUGUCCUAUCAAUGGAAACUUUAACAAAGGAGCUAGAUUUUGGUUUUACAGGACUCUUAGAUCUAUGGAUUAAGAUGUGUCUGUAAUAUUAGAUGUAUCUUAGAGAAUAAUUAUCCAAAAUAUACUUCAUGGAACAUGGAGGAACUACAGACUAACAUUUUCUAUGGUAAAAUAUUUGGGAAAUGCUUCAUUUUUUCUUUCAUAAUAUAUUAACACGUUAAAGGCCAAAUCAACUAUUUAGGAAAAGAAAAUAAAACAAAAUUUCACCAACUUUAUGAAGCUAACAUUUCCUGAGCUUUAACAUUUUUCAUUUGUUAUUAUUUUUUGAUACUAGGAAAGCCUUCUUGUGAUACUAUUAAGAUCCCAUAGAACAUUGCAAAUGCUUGUCCAAACCUGCAAAAAAAAAAAAAAAAAAAAGCGCACAUCAUGUGCAGAGACUUCCCAUGGGCAUUGGGUGCAGCUAUUUGUAAUGAGAAACAAAAUAACUGUUGGCUUCCGUAGUGGACUUGUGAGAACCAGUAGUUUUGCAUGGUGCAGGGAUAGAUAAGAAAGUUGUUUUCGAUAUGCUAUUUUGGAUUCUCUCACUCUAGGAAAUAAUCAAGUGUUGAUGGUAUUAAAUUUCCUUUAGCAUACAUGCAAAGAGGGCAUGUUUAUAGACUUUGACUUGAACUUCUUCUAACAGGCCUUAUUUUCCCUGAGUAUGUUUCUACUUACUUAAAAACAGAUGCUCUCUGAAAAAUUCAUGAAAACCAAAAAUAUGCUGGAGACUUUGGAGAGAAGCUCUUCACCCUGUUAUUAAAGUUAGAUUGUUUCUAACAAUUUUUUUUUGCAUCUUCUGCUUGGCAGUUAACUUCAUGACCUUGAACAACCUUUCUGGCUUUCCUGUAACUCAGUUUCCUUCAUUUACCUACCUACUUAACCAGAUUGUACAUAAAAAUACAUAGUAUAUAUAUAAAUGGUUAUAUUAACAGAUAGAUCCUUUCAAACACACUUAUAUUGGUGGCUUUGUUAAUGAAUAUUGCAUUUGUGGCAGAUAGACAUGUUUCCUUAAAUGAAGGUUUUCAAAACUGGCAUUGUAAGUAAAUUUUACAUAUUAUCAGUUGCUUGCACCCAAAACUAUUUCUACUGUGAACUGGAAUACAUCUUAAGAAAUUAUUUUAAAAGAUGUAAAUAACUAGUGGUAAAGUGAUAGAGCACAUCAUAACUUUCUUCAUUAUCAUAAGUAAUGUGGCUUUGUCCAUAUGUUAUUCUCAUUUGAAUUAUAAUUCUUAUUUUUAUUGUAUGGGGGUUUGCACACUUUUGUCCUCAACUUUUCUUGUUUAUUUUAAAAAGGGAGUCUCAGGAUUUUUCUUCUGAAGUUAAAAUUUAACCCUAAAGAAAGAUGCCACAGUAGUUUAGUCUGCUUUUCUGGAGCUCUGAACCAUUGAGGGCCAGAACUGACACUAUAAGCAGGAGCAGCAGUCCCAAGAUGGGAUUCUAAUAUCAACCUUUGUUUUAUCUGAUUCACUAUGAGUAAGAGGAUACAAUAUGAGUGAACAGCAAACCUGUGAGAAACCUACAAGUAUAAAACCAAUGGUAUUUAAUUCAGGUAAUAAAAUAGAAUUCUUAAACACCCUCUAAAUUAAAAAGCCAGAAGAUGCAGUUCUAAUUACAUGCCUUAACUAGAAGUAGGAUAUUUGCAGCUUAUCAAGUUUUAUGUAAAUUUGUUCCUUUGGCACAAUUUGCCUAUAUAAGCAGUAUUAGUUCAGUAUAAAAUGUUUAUUAGUUAUUGAAACUGGCUCUAGUGUAAUUUCUGUGUUUUAAUACAUAGUCCCAAGUUUUGUGGGAUCCCUAGAGAGAACUGUGUGGUGUCUAUGUUUUGAAUAAACAGGUUUUUUGAAUAAUAGUAACUUACAUAUCUAUAGUCUCUUAUCUGAAGCCCUUGGGGUCAAAAGUAGUUUAGAAUUUUAGAUUUUAGAACGGUAGUAUGCUACUAGUGCUGUGUGCUAUGUGACAUUCCAAUAGAAUCUUGGGCAAUGGCCAAGCAUGUUGACAUUUCUUAGUGCUUGAAUGGGAUAAAGAUCAUAAAGAGCAUCUUUUUCAGCUGAGGUCAGGUUGGGCUGACAGUGUGUUUGGUUUUCCAGAGCGUUUUGCAUAUUGGAACUGCAGAUAAGGGAUUAUGGACCUGUAAUAUUAAAUAUAAUAGCUGACAUGUAUUGUGUUUAUUCCAAGCCAGACAUGGUACUUUACUUGUAUUAUCUCAUUUAAUCUUUGCAACUCUUUGAAGAAGGUGAUAGUAUUAAUUUUGUUUUACAGAUGAGGAAGAGUUUCAGAGAAGUUAAGAAACUUGCCUAAGGAUACAUACACCUAGUAAGAAAGUGGUAGAGUUACAUCUCAACUAAGUCGAAUUAGACACCAAAUCUGGUGUGCACAAUAACUAGUUAUCCUCCUCGUAUUCAGUGUCUCUGAUUUGCAGCCCAUAGACUCAGUCUUACAUCAACAUAAAGGGAAUUAAUACGAAGGGUAUCAGGUGAUGGAGUAUCAGGCCCAGGGGAUAAUUGGGGGAAAGAAUGAGUCUCAGUAGCAACACUUCUUUGAUAGUCUUUCUUGGCCAUUUCCAUUAGAAUAAAUAUACUUCUAGUAGCAGUAAGAUUCAGAUGAGAGAGAAUACUUGAGCUUGUGUUGCUGUUAGCUAGGGUAAAGUGGGGUGUCACAAAUCCAGCAUGAUGGAGCAGUGUUCCUAAAGGAAAAUUGAUUGCUGUCAGCAAAAGAUGUGAUUCACGUGAGACAGCACACUCAUGUAAAAUGUCCACUGUAUGGAUGAUUAAUUAAUUGCAGAUGAAACUAACAUUUGGAUGAAAACCCCAGUUAGUUUUUUAAGUAUAAUCCAUUUUAAGUUUACCACCUGCUUGAUACCAGCAAAACAGUUAACUUAUCAUCUUGAAUACUCAGAUUCCUGUGGCAGUUCAGACACUUUCUAGGUCUUGGAUCUCAGAUCUAGAAUCAGUGAGCUUUUUUCUUAUUUGUAAUCUGAGAGCAACAGUACAUCUCCCAAUUUACCUAGUGGGCAUUGUGUUAGCUAAGAUAGCCCAAAGAGCUUCUGGAAGUUCAUACCCUAUGUGUUCAUAUUUCUCAUGCUGAUUCUGUGUUGUUCUUGUAUAACCAGCAGAUGCAGUAGGGGAGAUCCUGCAUAACUUCUGUGGCCAAGUCAUAAGGAGCCUUGCAGUGUCCACCUUAUUUUCUUGGCAUCUUCACUCUAGGGGAAGCUACUGCCAUGUAAGAAGUCUGAUCAUUAUGCUGUGAGGAAGUCCAAGCUAACCACGUGGAGAAAGAUCAAUUCCUGGCCAGCCAGCUGCUAUUCUAGCUCUCCCAGCUAGUGUGCCAGACAUGUAAAUUACCUUGGACAUCCCCACCCAACCGAACCAUUAGUUCAUUUCAGUCUAAAGUGCCAUCUGACUGAAAUGGCAUGAACGAUACCAAGGGACAACUGCCCAGCUGAGCCCAGACCACUCACAGAAACACGAGGGGCAAUAAUCCACGGUAAUAAGUCACUAGGUUUCCCCGUAGUUUGUUAUCCAAUAGCAGAUAUCCAGAAACAGGUUUGCUGUGAAGAAGAGAGAUAAUGUGUUAUAUUCCUCAAAUGAAGGUGAGCAGCUGUUUUAUUAUAAUUGCUUUGACAAUCCAGAAAGCAAGGUCUUUCUAAUAUCCUCAGAGGUUUCAUUACAAUUUGCCAUUGUGAUGAGGAUAGUGAUCAUGCUGUACUCUCUGGACAGGGAUGGAGAGUGUUAGUGAUUGGCCAGCAUCCAAGAUUGUCAUCAUUUUUCCUUAGUGCAGGAGUUUAAAACAUUCUGCCAUUUUCUCACUCGUAUUUAUAUUUUCACAAUGAAUGGGGUUUUCUCUAAUAAGAUUACUGUCAUAAAGUCUCUUAUUUAAAACUUCUGAUGGAUCCUCAUUGUGGAUGACAGGGCCCAUUUCUCUGUUUUUGUAGACUGUCCCUCUGUCCAGAAACUACAGGGGAAAUAAGAUGUAGAUUUUGAAAAAGUGACAGCGAGUCAAAGAACAGUUGGUCAAACAGCUUCCCAGCAGUUGGGACAGGCUGCCAGAGUGAAUGUCAAAGAGAAGUUGGUUCUUGGAUGGUUUUACAGAAAAACAAGACAAUGAAACAAAGAAAUAAGAAAUAAGUAGGAGGCAUGCAGAGGGACAAAAAUGAAGGACUUGAUAUUAGGACACCAGAGCAAUCAGUAGUAGGUUGGAUAGGAGGAGUUGAGAAGAGGGAGGAGGAAGCAACUAAGGGUUGGUUGGAACUUCAACACUUAAUGGGUUCACUCCCUCCUGUCUGUAAUUAAUUCUAGCUUUAGUUACUUCAUUUUCUCCUUAGAGGAAGAUAAAGUGACCUGGACUAUCUUCUUUAUGUUAUAGUUGUUUAGAAUCAAAGGGCAUUUUCUUAAAGUCUCUUUUCCCAAGUAAUUCUUAAGAUUUCUUAAGUGUCAUUGUCUCUUCAGGUGGAGUCAUAAAAUGCAUCUCUAUGAGGGGCAAUAAAAUGCAUGGAGGUGCCUUUUAUGGCUGUUGCUAGCAGAGGACUAGAAUAAGAUAAUGAUGGUAUUUUGCAAAUAGUGAUAAGGAGCAAAUUGCACAUUCCAAUGUCAAUCUGUUCUCAAAAGAGUAUAGUUCAAAGUUUCUACAAAGCUUUUUGAAAGCUUUUCUUUUUUGAAAUGAGUCUCUGAUUUCUGUUUUUCCUAGCUAUACAUAGAUUUUAUUUUGGGGAAAAUUUUAGGUAGUAACAUUAUCCUUAAUAUUUACUGAUUUGCUGUAGAAUUUUAAACUGGACAAAUGAAAGCCCUUGAGGAAGAGAAAUUUAUAUUCUAACAUAGCGAAAUAAAUAUAUGUCUUGCAACUUGAAUUGUUGUUAGGAAAUUACUUGUAUGCCUGAGUUCAUGAAUUAUUUAAUUUAAGAUUAUUUUCCUUUUUCUAAUUUAUCACUGGCUAGGUCCUUUAACAAUCUUUUGAUUUAUUAAGAGUCAUUUUCCAGAAUUAGAUUUAAAGCUCUAUUGUUUUCUUAUGAUUUUCCUAUGAAAAUUGAGUAUGUCUCCUAUAAAAGCUAUAUUUCUCUUGUUUGACUUAUUUCAUUUCUCUAUUAUGAAAGGCAAUCAUUUUAAAACUGAUGAAAUUUUAAAAAAUUGACCUAAUCUGAAAAAACCAGCCCAUUUCAUGAUCCUUCUUCACUUAUUGGAAAAGACUAUGGAGUCAGGAGUUGGGGAAUGUACCGACCUCCAUUAAGAGGUAAAUGACUUGCUUGUGUCUAGAAGCGUUUGUGUCAUUUGCCUCUCAGUGCUUGCUGCAGUUUUAAGGAAAUUGUCCUCCUAUUAAGGUUAUGUAUCAGAAUCACCCUUGAAACUUUUUAUUAAUAAAGAUUCUCUGUCCCCACAAUGAGGUUUAUUAAAUCAGAAUCUCCAGGGCACUGGUGUGCUGAACGAGUCUCCUAGGUGAUUUGAAUUCGUACCCCAGUCUGCAUCUGAAAACUGCCGCUUUUCAAAGAGAGGCAGACAGGUUGAUGGAUGAUAGGAUCCAGUCUGACACAUGGAAAAGCUACAAGGAGGGAGCAUGGAGGAAUCCUUCAUUUAGGGAGACAUGAGUAUUGUGAAUGAUGGUGUAAUCACUGCUAAAAAUUUCUCGGGUUUCUAAGAAAGUUUUAUGUCCUCAGUUUUCUUGAUGGUGUCUCCAGCCAAGCUGUAAUGCAGUGGUUCCCAACUAGGGGCAUCUUGGUCUCCAGGGGCUAUUUGACAAUGGCUGGUCCUAUUUUUGGUUGUGAUAACUAAGGGGAUGCCGCUGGCAUCUAGUGAUUAGAGGCCAGGGAUGCUGCUGAACACCCUCAGUGCAAGGGGAGCCCUGUGUUAGUCAGAAUUCUCCAGAGAAACAGAACAUAUAUGAUGGCCCAGCUUAUGCGGCAGUCAUGUGGGAGUUUUCUCUUACUCAGCUUUUUGUCCUCUUUUGAUCUCCAAUUGAUUGGGUGAGGACCUCCCACAUUAUGGAGGGCAAUCUGCUUUACUUAGUCUGGAGAUUCAAAUGUUAACCUCAUCCAAAAUAUCCUCACAGACACACCCAGAAGUACAUUUGACCAAAUGUCUACACAACCUGUGGCCCAGUCAAGUUGAUAUAUAAAAUUGACCAUCACAGCCCCUUACAACAAAGAGUUAUCAGGCCCAAAAUGUCAGUAGUAUCAAGGCUGGGAAACCCUGAUCUAGUGAAGUGCAGUGAAAUUCUCAAAAUAAAAAUAUUCUAGGGGCCAGCAUUGAAAAGGAUGUGGCAGGGCCAGGUAGGAGAGCAUUAGAGAUGGCCUGUGUGGACCUUGAGGAAGCCAGAUGAGAUAAAGAGGAGGAGAGGGCAUGAACAUAGGAUAAAAGCUCGAGACAGGAAGAGAUGGGGUUAAAAUGAACAUCAGGUACUUGAAAAGAGGGAUGUUCAUCAGGUGUUAUUUUUCCUAGCAGUGUUAUGUAAAAUACGAGUACUAUCUGAAAGUCUGAAAAAGGUAGGGCCAAUUUAACAUCAGCUUUAAGAUAGUAAAUCUCUAUUCUGUAAGAUGUAAUGGUAGUUUUUAAGCCUUGAAAAUUGGAAAUGUUAGACAAUGGUAGCAUAUGUGAGCCAGAGAGAAUUUGAUGGUAAAUUUGUAGUACAGAACUUUAGACUUGUUUUUACCAGGAAGAAGCAUCAGAGAAACAGUGAGAGUAAUCAGCGCAUAUUUGUUGUAUUUCCGAGGCUGGUAAUGGAGCUAAAGUGUGGGGGCAGAGCUUUUUGUUUGGGAAAGUGUGGAAAUGGGGCUGGUCAAUGCAGAUGAAGGGGUGCUAUGGGAACCUUAUGAUGUAAAAUACACUCUCUCAUUGUCUUCACAAGUGUAGCUCUAAUUGCCUGACCUAUGUGCAGAUUUGUUGUUCAGAACAAAUGGGGUUACCAUAAGUAUGGAAAAUGGUUCCUGGUCUACAGCGAAUUGGAGAGACUAGAGAGGCAAGCCAGUGCUCUUAAAUAGCAGUGACCCAUCUAAGUUCAUUUUUCAUCACCCUUCUGGUAAAUACUUCCUAAUUUUCUCUAGGGGAUGUGCUUUCCCCAUGUUUGAUCUGUUUUUUUCUGAGAGGUGUUUGGUUCAUCCUGGUUGUAGGGUUGGGUUUGUGAUAUAGGCAUAGCCUCUCAGAGGCAUUUGGCCAUAAGUCUUAUCUGGGUAUGGGCUCAUGACCCCAGGUCAAUCUAGUCAGAUCUGCUGAUGUUAAUUCUGAGGCUCUUUUCUUUCCUUACUUUUGUAUUUGGAGGUGUAAGGAUGUAAUCCCACGUUCUUGGUCAUAAUCUUGUCAUACUAUAGAAAGGGACUUUUUCAAAAUGUAGUUAAUUCAAGGAAGACCAGAGUUGAGAGACCUUAUAUCAUUUGUGCUCCUGGAUGAAGCUGUACCUGAAGCUAGGUUGUCCCAGAAUUCUGUUAGUAAACUAUUAAAUUUCUUUUUUGGUUAUACUAGUUUGUGUUGUUUCUUUCACUAAUGACUGAACAAAUUACUAAAAGAUACACUGAAUUAUUAGGAGAAACUGUCCAAUUAGUAAGUGAUAUAGCCAACUAAUAACUAAUUAAUUAAUGUUUCAUACUCCAGUAUUUGGGCUCUGUGUAUAUAUUGGUGAUAUUCUUCCAUUCUUGUUUGUUUGUGUUUUGGAGAGUUUGACAAAAAUGCAUAGGCUAUCUCUGGUAAUGCUUGGUUUAAAGCAUAUUUCAUAUUCAGAAAGAUGUUGUAUUUGAGAAGCGACGUGGUAAUUGGUUUUGAGAGUAUACAUCUUAGACAAUUAAAUGGUUACAUUGCUUCCUUCCUUGGUUUAAAAAAAAAAAAAGAAAUCCAAGGGUAUUCCAGUUGUAUAAAUAGGGACAACACAGUUUAUGCUAUUUGUAAUUACAGAUACCACUCAAAAGAAUUGAUUCCGUUUACUUUUGUAUUAGUGUACUGUGGAAAGUCGUUAAUUAUAAUGUCUGUUCUUAUCCAACAACAUGCAAUAAGUAAAGAUGAAAAUAUAGAGAUUAUUAGUUUGAAUAACUGGUUGCAUGCCAUCCGGUUUUAUAUGAUUGCUGAAAUGCAAAACAAACAACCCCUCCCCCCGAAGAAAACAACCCACCGUUCUUAAAUAAGACAUUUGUGACAUAACAAAUUAGAAUCUAGGAGAAGGAAAAUAUUUUCCCAGUAUCUAAAGCCAUUGAAUCAAAAUAAUCGUGUAGAUCACACUUUAGUUCAGAUAUAACCUAAAUAAAUUCUCUAGCCAGGGCACCCAUCUGUCAAAAAAUAAAACUCUGGCCCUCAUUUAAAAUGGCUCCUUUAGACUGAGGUCAUCUAGCUGUAUCUAAAUUGGACAUGAAAUGUCAAUUUCAUACCUUAUAGUGGCACAUUUCAUAUUGCUCUACUUAAGGUUAUGUCAGCUUUACCCAUAAAAUGCAAGUGAUUUAGGUCUUAUUCUAAAUGAACUAACCAGAUACAUCAGCAAUGGGCACUGCCUUGCCACUGCAGAAAAAGGGAAUGUGUGAAGGGAAGACAGAAACCACUUAUUCUGUUUCUUAACUCUGGAAGUAUAGGUAUUCCAGGUUGGGAUGUCUUGUCUAUAUUUUCAUUCCUUGUGAAUGAUAAUUUGGGGGUGGGGGGAUUAGAAAGAUGCUUUAUUCAAAAUGAAUUGUAUUGCCUGCAGGCGAUUCACUUGCUUAAGUUAUAUUUGUGAGUUAUUGUAUGUAACUUUAUCACAUUGGAAAGUUUAUGAACCUUGUGUAGAAAAAAGAUUGCAUUUUGGGAGCUAUGCACAUCAUGGCUUUUUCACAAGUGACAGAAAAGUGCUGCAGAUGAUUUAAGCAGGAAGAAAUGAAUUUUUCGAAAGAUUUUGAGUCCAGAAGGGAGAUAGGGCAGUCAGUCUUGGAAGAUGAAAAGGACAAAGCCAAAGCGGGCCAGGCAGGCAAGGGAGUAGUGUUGUGAACGCCCUACCCCACCCCUACUGCAUCUGAGUGUUGCAACUGCCUGUGUUGCCACUAUGUAAACACUGCUCCUUAAUAUCUGCUUCCUUGGAUCCGAAUUCAGAGCCCUGGGGACAGUGCAUCUCAUUGGCUGAGCAUGUAUCAGCCAUUGGUAACCAAGCUGCAAAGAGGCUGGGAAAGUAAGUAGUCGGCUCUUUCAGCUUCUAGCUGGAAUGUGAUCACCUCCCAAUAUUCUUCUUCUUCUUUUUUUUUUUUUUUUUCGAGACGGAGUCUCGCUCUGUUGCUCAGGCUGAAGUGCAGUGGCACGAUCUCAGCUCACUGCAACCUCCACUUCCCGGGUUCAAGUGAUUCUCCUGCCUCAGCUCCCUAGUUACUGGGACUACAGGCGCCCGCCAUCACGCCUGGCUAAUUUUUGUGUUUUUUUACUAGGGACGGGGUUUCACCAUGUUGGCCAGGCUGGUCUUGAACUCCUGACCUCAAGUGAUCCACCUGCCUUGGCCUCCCAAAGUGCCGGGAUUACAGGUGUGAGCUACCGUGCCCAGCCCCAGUAUGUCUUCUUAUAGUGGGGGGUAUCUAAAAACAGGAAGAAGUUUCAGAUGCUUGGCAGCUGACAUGGCUAAUUUUAGGUCAACUUGACUGUAUCAUGGGGUGCCUGGAUAAAACAUUGUUUCUGGGUGUUUCUGUGAAGGUGUGUUAGGUUGAGAUCACCACUAGAAUAAAUGGACUUAGUAAAGCAGAUUGUGAGUGGUCAUCAUCCAAUUCACUGAGGGCAUGAAUAGAACAAAAAUACCGAAGGGGAAAAAUUAAGAAUUUGUCCCUUUCUCUUCCUGCCUGCUGGUUGAGCUGGGACAUUGGUCCUCUCCUGCCCUGGAACUGGUAUUUAUACCAUUUCCUGGUUAUCAGGCCUUCAGACUUGAACUGGAAUUACACCAUUAGCUCUUCUCUGGAUCUCCAGCUUAUAGAUGGCAGAUUUUGGAACUUCUCAGUCUCCAUAAUCAUAUGAGCCAAUUCUUUGUAAUAAAUUUUCUUCUCUCUCUCUCUCUCUGCCUAUCUAUCCAUCUAGUUAUCUGGAUAUAUCGCCUAUGGGUUUUCUUUCUCUGGAGAGCUCUGACUAAUAGAGUAGCCAAAGCAAAGACAGUUUGUAUGUGUAUGGUUUUAUGGGGAGUGGAUUUUCAGGAAAGCAGGAAAAAGAUUUUUUCCAGGGCACUUGGGUAGUGCAUCUUUUUUCCUCUAACAAAUGGGGGAGCAUGUGGCCUUCUGAGUACUGGGUUUGCUUAAUGAAUCAGGAGAGCCAGUGUUUAUAAAUAUUCCUUUAAAUGGCAGAGCGUAGAUCCUGGUUUGUAGUCCCCUUAGUAUAUUUGUAAUGUUUUCAUCAUACCCCUAGGCCAAAGAAAAUACUCAACAUUAAGUAGUUUUAUUCAUUAGGUAGGUAGGUUGAAACAAAUGAAUAAGAAUUUAUGUACUAACGUAAUUUGAAAAACAUAUAUAUCAUUUGAAAAAACACACAAAUUGAAAUAAAAUAUUUUUUUCUUAAAUAACCACUAUUGCUUACUAAUGGGAUAUAUCCUCCUGUUGGGCACAGAAUGACUUCACAUACAUUGGAAUUAGAUUGGACACUGCUACCUGAUUCCCAUCCACAUUGAUUUUCAUGACGCACAUUUUAUUACAGCAAUGGCUAUGAACCCAGCUUUGCAAAGAUAUAACAUAAUGAAAAGGAAUGUAAUGCAAUCAAAUAUUGAAACUGCCAACUACCUCGAGCUAUCCUGACAGUUGAGCAUAGCUUGGGAGUGGUAGACAUAGAUUAUCACUGAAAUUCUAAUGUGAGCCUGAUGGCAACUUGAGUUGAAGGGCAUUCUUGCAAGACUGCUUGGUUGGGGAGUGUCACACCAGCUGGAUGUUUCCAGAACCAAGGGCCUGGGAAAAACUAUGCCAGUGUGCACAGUGCACACUCUUCCUCAGUGUAGCCACUCUGCUUCUGAUGUGUUUUGUUGUCUAAAUCAGUCAGCAACCUAUCACAGAUGUGUGCAUCUUUUCCUACCAAUCCACAAAACCCACCUGAUACGGUUUGUCUGUGUACCCACCCAAAUUUAAUCUUGAAUUGUAAUCCCUAUAAUUCCCACCUGUCAUGGGGGGCACCCAGUGGGAGGUGAUUGAAUCAUGGACACAGGUCUUUACUGUGCCGUUCUUGUCAUAGCAAAUGCGUCUCACAGGAUCUGAUGGCUUUAUAAAGAGGAGUUCCCCUGCACAAGCCCUCUUGCCUGCCGCCAUGUAAGAUGUGCCUUUGCUUCUCCUUUGCCUUCCACCAUGCUUGUGAGGACUCCCCAGCCAUGUGGAACUGAGAGUCCAUUAAACCUCUUUUUCUUUAUAAAUUACCCAGCCUCAGGUAUGUCUUUAUUAGCAGUGUGAGAACAGACUAAUACACCACCUGAAAUAAUGUACCCCUUAAAAUCCUUAUUUAUGGAUUGAUGAGAAAACAGAGCUUUCAUUUUAUAUGAUUAACAGAAGAUAAGUGCCUCUGUUGCCCAGAUCAGACUGUCUUAGUUCAUUCAGGCUGCUAUAACAAGUUACCAUUUUCUGGGUAGCUCCUAAACAACAGAAAUUUAUUUCUUACAAUUCUAGGGUCUUGGAAGUCCAAGAUCACGGCAACCUCAGACACUUUUGGUGAGGGCCCACUUCCUGGUUCAUAGAUGGGCCUUCUUGCUAUGUUCUCACAUGGGUAUAGGAGGUAACAGAGCUCUCUGCAGCCUCUUUUAUAAGGGCGCUAACCCCAUUCAUGUCCUAAUUACCUCCCCCAAAGCCCCAACUCCUAAUAGCAUCACCUUGGGUAUUAGGAUUUCAAGAUAUGAAUUUUGGGGGAACAUAAACAUUCAGACCAUAGCAUAGGCCAAUUAAGAACUAGGUAUAUGUAAAAGCAUGGCUCCUUUUUUGGUACAAAGCUGGUGUAUGCCUCAAAAUUUAUAUUUUGCACUCAGAAAAAUUCUUCCUUUUAUUCCCUGAACUGCUUGUUCAUGUGAUCUCUACUUCUGUAUGUCCAGGUCUUUGAUAUGUGUAUGAGUUGACUGUUUCAUUGUGUCGGAACAUCUUUUGAUUGUGUCAAGAGUUCCAGCUUCUUUUCUUUAAAGAUCCUGUUUUAUAAUCUGCCAGCCUGACCACACUCAGCAUACAGUCUUCAAAGUUACAGGUUAUGUGAAACUUUCAAAUGAGAUAUUACUUACUCCUGUUCUUCAGCUGGAAUAUCAGUUGCUGGGGGAGCUGGAGAAACAAUUCCCAAAAUGAAGAGCACCUUAGCAUUUCUACAAUGUUGUCAUUGCAGGGUAUUGUGAUAGGCAGAAUGCUGGCCCUGCCCCAAAGAUGCCAGUGUCCUAAUCUCUAGAACCUCUGAAUAUGCUACCUCACAUGGCAAAAGGGACUCUGCCAAUAUGAUGAAGAUGAAGAAAUUGAGUUUAGAGUUAAAUGAUUGCCCAGGAUUAUGUUGUUACAAGUGCAGAAUCAGUAAUCAAAUUGCUGUGCUGUGUCCUCCAGGGCCUGAGUUCCUACAUUGCCAUGAGCCAUUAAAGGGCUACUCAGAUACACAUACUUGAACUGUAACAGCAAAUAGUGAGAGGGGAAGUAAAGAUUCUGAGCCUCCUUUCUGGGUUUACAGCAAUAUUUUGAACUAAGAAGAUGAAGUAGAAUUAGACAUGAGCAAAGCUCCAUCCCUUUCUUCUGCAGGUGAGAAAGAAAUAGAGGGUGUAGGAGGUAAGCAUACCUACCUAGUAAGCCUUCAUGAUUUAGGUAUCUGGAGCAGGUGGGACUGGAGCAAUUGCCAUGAAGUUCACAAUUUUAGUGUGGCCUGUGAUCUGUUUCUUUGGCUACAGCUUACAUAUCAGGCCUGGGGAUUUUUCUGGAUUCUGAAGGUUCUAGCUUCCAGCCUUGAAAUUAUUCUCCUACUUGUAGGUCAGUAAAACAAGCGUUUCUUUACUUGAAAGUUUUAAGUCGACAGUUGCCAUGAUAAAUCACUCCCACUGAUAGUGUUUUAGACUUUGUUGGUUCUACCUUACGGGAUUUUCAUAGAGUUUCUAAAAGAGAAAGACAAGCACUAGAGUGAAGAAUUGUUCUUAUUGUGGAAGAAUCAUCAACCUUGGCUGGACACACAGAUCAAGGGGUUCAGGGAUGGGUGGCAAAGGAUCAUUGAGAGGGUUACAUGUGACCCUUGCCUAACUAUAGUAGUUAAUUCAACUCUGCCUACACAAUGACACGGAUUACCGAGGAUAUGACUUGUAUUAUACUCAUCCCUCUGACCCCACAUCCUAAUGUUAAUAAUGAUUCUUAAACCUGGAAUUGAGAACUCAAAUAUAAACCAGUGCCCAGCACAUAGCAAGUCAUCAAUUAAGUUUAUUGAAUUAAAUUAAAUAUUGGAAUUGUAUCUGUCAAAGCCAUAUCAGCUCUAAGCUUCUUAAGAGAAAAAUCUGCCCAGAAUUUCUCAGGAGGGAUUUCUCAACAUCGAAGCUGUCCUGUUCAUAUUGGAUUUAUUGUACUUACAUAAACAGGAAUACACGAGCAGGGAAGAUCAGAUCAGUUACCACAAUAAGGGUUUUGUACCAUGAUAUACAUCAUUUUCGCUCCCCUAGGAAAGCACUGCUGAUGAAAACAAUUUUGGAGGGAGGUGGUCUCAACAGAGUAGAUGUUCAGGUGGAGGUUAUCUCUGGUGCUCUGGGCUUCUUAUUCAUAAUUUUCUCUUAUGAAAGAGAGUGGUUUUCAACUUCACAAUUCCUUUGCUCAUUUGGAAAUAUAGUAGCAGAAAGAUGAAGAGAGUUUGUGACCCACAACUAAAGUCUGUGUUCUCUUGUCACUUCAUCAAAUUAGUUCUGGUGGCAUUUGGUUCCCCCCCAGAAAUAAAUCACUGUUAAAUGAUUCUUUAUAAAGCAGUCCACACAUUUAUCAUACCACAGUGAUCUGAACCCAUUUAGGGAAUUAUAAGCUACAGUUGGUCAUGUUGCAGGCCUAGCAACUCUGGCCUUGUCACAUUGCAUCUCUCUCCACUCCCUGUGCUACCACUAAUCCUUCAGGACUGAGAUUCAAGGCUUUGCUAGUAAGAGGCUUGGAAAUAAUCAUAUAAAACAUAAUAGUGUGGCAAGGUGAGAUCGAGCUUUUAAUUUUUUUAAGUUCACAGAGAGCAAGAAGACAGAUAGGAAAGGACCGGCAGAUUGGGAAAAAUCAGGAAUAAGAUGAAAUAUCCUCAGAACUUUAGCUUUUAUGAUUCCACCUCACAUUCAGUUUAAUUAUGAAAUUUACUGGCAGUGACAAUUGGCUUUUGGCAUAAAUUAAUCAUGCCAAGCAUUAUACAUGAAAUGAAAUUUCAAUCCUAUUUGUUGAACAUUUUCUAAGAGCUUGGCAAUCUUGCCCAGCACUUUACGUAGGGUUUCUCCUUAUCUACCUUAUGAAAUAUGUUAUUAUUAUUCCCACUUUUAAUAUGAGAAUAUUUGGGGAUUAGAAGGCUUAAGUAAUUUGACAAAGGUCAUAUGGGCUAGCAUAAUAGACUAGAAAACAAACUCAGGAUGCUGUAAUUACUACACUGGAAUCAUUCUUAGUUUUUUUUUUUUAAAUGAAGUUGGCAUUAGUUUUGUUUUUUAAUCUUUAAUACUUUUAUCUGAGAAUUGAUAAUUAACCAUUUUAAGAAAAUAGUUACAUAAAUUUAGAAAUCAUUUGGAAAACAGGUAAAAUUGCUACAUUAUUUCAAUUUAUUUUAUUUUUAAAAUAAAUGAUAUUUUUUAUCUAUAUUUGAGGGCUAUAUGAGAACCUAAGACUUCUAUUGAUGUUAAUUAUUGACUUUUAUUUACUGUAGUUUUAGUGAAUAAUUUAAUUGACUUCUAUUAAUUCAGUCAUCAUAUGCUAAACCUAGAGUAACUGCUGUUAAUAUUUUUUUUUUUAGCUACUACAAAUUGAAGUAUUUUUGAUUAGAGUAAAAUUUAUUUCUAAAGGUAACCUGAGUAAUAUCUCUAUGUUGUAGAUAGAUAUUACUAUCUAUAGUAAUAUCUAUGCAUAUAGUAUCUAUGUAGUAGCUUUCCAAUUUAUUUUGCUAUUAUCUAAAAUAAGAAAUACAUUUUAUAUUGUUCCAGUAAAUGCACACAUAUAAACACAUAUAUAUGAAAUUGAUACUUCAUAAAAUAUUAGUUACCCUUAUUAUAAUCAGUGCUCACUUGAUAUUUUACAUUUUAUCCCAUUGUAAAAUAGAUACUGGUCAUGACUCACAGUAUUGAUUUCAUAACUCCCUAAUGGUUGUAGCCUGCAGUUUAUCAUUUGUUCAAAUGUAGUGUGGUGGGAAAGAAAGAUGAUAUGACUCUUCAGACAGAGAGGUCUGGUCCCUACCCUGAUAUGUGUCAGUUAUAUGUCACCUUACCUAUAAAAUGGUGAUUAUCAGUACUUCUCAGGGGAGUUGUAAAGCCUGGUACCUAGUAGAUAAUUAGUAAAUAUCAGUUUCUUUUGUCUUUAGAGCUCACACUUCAUUCCAUAGUUUUUUGUUGUUGUUUUGUUUUGUUUUUUUGAGACGGAGGCUCACUCUGUCGCCCAGGCUGGAGUGCAGUCGUGAUCUUGGCUCAUUGCAACCUCUGCCUCCUGGGUUCAAGCGAUUCUCCUGCCUCAGCCUCCCGAGUAGCUGGAACUAUAGGCACUCACCACCAUGCCCAGCUAAUUUUUGUAUUUUUAGUAGAGAUGGGGUUUCAUCAUAUUGGCCAGGAUGGUCUUGAUCUCUUGACCUCGUGAUCCACCCACCUUGGCCUCCCAAAGUGCUGGGAUUAUAGGAGUGAGCCACUGUGCCUGGCCUCAUUCCAUAGUAUUAUAGAAAAUGUCGAACUGUUUAAGCAUUCCAGCACUUUAUUUUUUAAUUGUUAUUAUUUUUCUACCCUCAGCAUGCAUCAGAGGAGCAUUCCAGCCCUUUAGUUUGGAUUUUCUUGCUAUUUCUGAUUUUAACUAUGUGUGUUCUUCAUAUCUUGGACUAAAAAAUAAAAACAAAUUAAAAAUAGCAAAAAAAAAAAUUUGCAGUAAUUUUAACAGACCAACAUUAAGUACUCUGGAAGCCAGACCAGAAGCUAGGGGCUCGUUAAUUUUUAUGUAUCAUCAAUGGAAAUGACUUUUAUUUGUUAAUUAUUUUUUAUGACCACCUAUUGUAACAUCUUCCAACACAUAUUUCCCCCUCUUUCCCGUCCUCCACUCUUUAACCUUCCUUGCCCAUUUUUUGUAGAGAUGCCAGUGAGGUCUUUCUCAGUCAGUGCUUCAAUCCCAUUAUUUCCCAUCUCAACAGGCUUCACUGGCUCACCAUUAUCUUUCAUAUUAGUCACAGGCUCCUCAGCCUGAAUUGAGGCCUUUAUGACACAAUUCUAGUCUACCUUUGGAGAUGUGCUUCCUUUCAGUGUCCUCUCUGUAUUUCAUACUUACUGCUUUGAUCAGACAAGAUGGCCUGUCUUUUUCCAAAUGGAUCUCACAAUUUCCAGGCUCUGUGUAUUUGCUUAUGUUGUAUCCUCUACCUAGAAGUCUUUUCUCCUGGUCCAUCUGUCCUCAUUAAAAACUCCACUCCUGUUUUCAAAUUCCUUGUCUGUUUCAUCGUGACUCUUCUAAUUGAUUCUCUUUCACUCCCACACUACUUCUAUUGAUGUUGAUUUCUCUGAAGCUGGCUCCUAGUGCCUUUUUUCUUCUUAAGGCAUGAUAGUGUGUCUCAAGUUGGAAUGAUUUCAUGGCUCCCAUAUGGUUGAUUGGUUGUGGGACUUUAUCGCUAAUGAUAAUUCAGAAAAUAGUAGUAGGACUAAUUGCAAUUCUGCAGAUUUCACCUUAAACAUAUGCUGCUUCUUGGGCUGUGGAAGUUGGACACAUUGAGAUAAGAUUAUUCAGAAAAACAGCAAGGCCGGGCGCAGUGGCUCCCUCCCAUAAUCUCAGCACUUUGGGAGGCCUAGGUGAGAGGGUCGCUUGAGCCCAGGAGUUUGAGAGUAGCCUGGGCAUUAUAGGGGUACCCUGUCUCUACAGAAAAUAAAAAAAAAAAAUUAGCCUUGGUGGUGUGUGCCUGUAGUCCCAGCUACUCAGAUGGCCGGGGUAGAAAUCACUUGAGCUCAGAAGACACAGGUUGCAGUGAGCUGAGAUUGCACCACUGCACUUCAGCCUGGGUGACAGAGCGAGCCCCUGUCUCAAAAAAAAAAAGAAAAGAAAAGAAAAAAAUAUUAGUAGGUCUAACUGUAAUUUUCUAACUUCUGGUUUUAAAUAUACACUGUUUCUUGGGCAGUGACAGUAGGGUAAAAUUACCCAGUUUGUGUAAAUCUUAUGAGGCUUGAUAAAUGGACUUAAUAAUUAUCAGAUGACGAAAUUAAAUGAGUCGGUGAAUGUUAAUGCGUCCCUCCUUCCAUGUAACUAGAUGCCUUGGGACAGUUCCAAUAUGUGGCAUUUAUAUUGUAUUAUGAUGUGUUAAUAAUGUGGAUCAGAGACAAGCAAAAGUCAAGGAUAAAUGUAAUUUCCUGUGAAAUGUAUAUUUAAUACUUUUUAACAUUUAGCGGAAUUACCUUUGGAUGUCAAUUGAACAUUACAUCCCCUUACUACCGUGACUGUGUGUGUGUGUGUGUGUGUGUGUGUGUUGGGGGGGUGGUGUCUAAGGAGUAAAUCUAUUCUCUUACUGCAAUUUCAAACACUGAAGUAUUAUAAACUUUCUUUAAUUGUAUCGAGUUUUAUAUAUUUUGUUGAUUCUAAGAGUUUUUGUGUAUGUGUGUGAUAUCAGUGAAUCAGGCAAAUUUCCCAGUGUGUGAAGCUUUUGGGUCAGCUAUUAGGUUAUUACAUCAUUUCAGAAAUGCUCCGUCUGCCUUCUGGUGGCCUUCAGAUUUGGCCAAGUAGUGGAGUAGUGCAAAGACUGCUAAUAUUGUAGAAAUCCCGUGACCAUACGCAGUGGUUUUUAUUUUGUUCUAAGGGGUACACACUUCCAUUUGUCUGUUUUCAUGCGGAGCACAUUUAUAUGAGGGUAAGUUCAAUGGCAACUUUUAGUCUGUAGAGGGAUACGUUGAGAAAUAUGUUACUGACCAUAAAUUACCAAUUUGAGAUGAAUGCAUACUUCAGAGGCCCCACUAGCUCACAUUUUUACUGCUGUCCCCUAAAAGCACCUUCAGGUUUAUAUGCUGAAGAUGGAGACCUUCAUAGUUAGAAAAUUGCAUUCCCUCAGGCCACAGGAAAUAUUGCUUGACAUUCUGUAACACUAUUUGAUGUUCUUAAAACAGCAUGCUAUGUAGAUACUACUCUAGGUCAUGUCUAAUUUUUUAAUCUGUAUUUAUAAAUACUAUGAAGCUUGUGGUUUUUAAGAAUAGUAAUGUUUACAUUUAUAUAAUUUGAUGCAAUGACUUUUCCCUGUAAUAUAAAAUUAAUUUAAUGUUUAGUAUAAAGGAAAUAACCAGGUUGUAUAGUUGUAGGUUGUGCAACUACAGGUUGUGUAGUUGCAGGUUGUGUAGUUGACUUGUGUAUUUUCACUUCCUCAUACUGACAACAUAACCAGAGGCCUGACCAAUGCUGGUGAAAUAACCAAAAAGGUUGUCAGGCAGACCUUUGCGUUUUAAUGCAAAUUCAACAGGGAAUGGGGUGGGCAUAGCUUUUUUUUUUUUUUCUGUAUUAUAUCAAGUAAGCUGAAUAUAUGCAAGGUUAGAGUUUAAAUGUAAUGAUUAGUUUUAUUCAUAUACAUUUAAAAUCUAAUAUUCUACAAGAUGCUUAGCACCAUACUUGACACAUUGUGAGCAUUCAGUAAACUGAUGUUAUCCUUUAAGAAGCAUUUACCACAGAGGUUAAGAGCAUAUGCUCUAGAGCAAAGUUGCCUAAACUAUUUCUGCCUCUGUUUCAUCAUUUCUAAUAUAGGGAUAGAUCAUUUAGUUCAUAGAACACUGUUAAAUCCAUAUAAAGCAUCUAUAACAGUGUUUUUAAUAAGUAAAAAAAAGUCAGCUAAAUAUUAGUUGUUUAUUAAUUGUAAUAUAUCCUAAAGCAACUUAUUUCUUAACGUAGACUUCUGCACAUUCUUGGAAAAUUAAUAUCUCUUUUUUUCCUUGCAAUUUUUUUGGAUAUUUGAAACUAUAAGUAUCUUCACCCAGUUGUAGGACAUAUGUUUUUCUAUUUUCUUCCCCCUUGUUGGAGAAAUCUAUUUCUACGGGACAAGCUGGUUAUUUGUCUACAGAUCCUCCCCUGGGGAUUCUGUAGCAGCUACUUCAAAGCUAUCUCAGCUUGCACUUAAUCAUUUGAAACAUCAGAUAACUUGCUUGUUCAUUUUAUGCAUGUUUUCUUAUUGAGGAAAUUAGUCAACCUAAAAUGAGCACCAGAAGAUUAUUUUUCUUGGUUUUACUCUUAAAGUCAUUCUCAAGCAUGUUAUCUUGGAAGAGCAGGGCACUCUCCUGCAGCUUUUAAGGAUGACUGAACUGGAGAACAUUCUGUUUAACCACAAAACUCAUGUUCCCUCUGUUUAAUUUCUUAAAGCUUGCCCUCCCUUCAAUGCAAUUACCAUUUUUCUUACACAUUAAGAGGACAAAAUUUGUUGGCUUCCUCUUUGGGGGAGGAUGUUUAUUUAUUUAGAAGAUACUUUUUGAGUUCCUACUGGUCCACCGGGAACUAUCGUAAGUAAGUUGAGGAUACAGGGAUGAGCAAAAUGGACAAAUUCUUUGUUCUCAUGGACCCCACAGGAGAAGAAAGACAAUAGCUAGUAAGCAAGUAAUACAUUUUUUUAGACAGCUAAUUUUUGUAUUUUUAGUAGAGAUGGGGUUUUGCCAUGUUGGCCGGGCUGGUCUGGAACUCCUGACCUCAAGUGAUCCGCCCACCUCAGCCUCCCAAAGUGCCGGGAUUACAGGCAUGAGCCACUUCGCCUGGCCAACAAGUAAAUAUUUUUGACUAUGUGGAAAUAUGAUGAAGAAAAUGAUGAAUAGGAAAAUGGGACUAAGAGGCAAGAAGGGCGAAGCAUCUAUGAGGAAGUGGUAUGUGGACAGAGAUUUGAAUGCUGACAGGGAGGCAGCUAAGAGACUCUCUGAACAAAGAAGUAUCCAGGCAGAAGGAACAGCAUGGGCCAGGGCUCUGGGGCCAAAACAAGCUCAGUCUGGCUGAGAAAGGGAAUAAAUGACUGAACACAUUUCUGUAGCCUUCUAUGUUCCAGGUGCUAUCCAAGGUGCUUGGGAUACGUCAGCCAACAUAUUUGCAAUGUUUUGCAUAGUUGUCCUCUCCAAAACUCAUGUCGAAAUUUAAUCCCCAGUGUAGCAGAAUUGAGAAUUGGGGCCUUUAAGAGGUGAUUAGACCCUGAGGGAUCUGCCCUCAAGAAUGGAUUCAUCCACUCAUGGAUUAAUGGAUUAAUGACUAAUGGACUAAUGAGUUGUCAUGAAAGUGGGACUGGUGGCUUUAUAAGAAGAGGAAAACAGACCUGAGCUAGGACACUCAGUCAUGUGACAGCCUGUGCCACCUUGGGACCCUGCUGAGAGUCCCCACCAGCAAGAAGGCCCUCACCAGAUGUGGCUUCUUUAUUUUGGACUUCUCAGCCUUCAUAACUGUAAGAAAUAAAUUUCUUUUCUUUAUGAAUUACCCAGUUUCAGUUUAUUUUGUUAACAGCAACAGGCUAAGACAAUAAUGCAUGAUUUUUUCUAAGUAAAUUAUGUACAAUAUUAACUGAUCAGUGUUUUAAAAAAAUGUUUGUAUGCAGGGAGGUAAGAGUGCAGGAAUAGGUGGGCUACAGUGUAAAACACUGAGGUCAAGGUAGGUCUCAUAGAGCAGGUGGCAUUUAAACAAAGUAUUGAAGGAGACGGGGCAAGUUUGUCAGAUGGGUAUGUGGGAGAAGGAAUUACCAGGCACAGGUAAUAGCUAGUACAAAAGCCGUAAGGUAGCAGUAGGCCCAGCUUGUUCCAAGUGCCUCAAGAAAGCCUCUGUAACUGGAACAGAGUGAGUGAGAUGAGUGAGGCGGAGAAGAGGUUAGAGAAGUGAUAAGAGGUGGCAUCAGGCCAGUCUUUGUAAACCACUGUCAGGACUUCCGUUUGAUUGAAACGAGGUGCCGUCUGGUAGGUAGCUUUGGGGUCUAGACUGGGGAGGGGUGGAGCAAAGUUAGGAGCAGGGUGACUUGUUAGCAGAAUAAUGGAAUAAGCCAUGAGCCACACUCUGGUUGCUCUUACAGGGCCGUGGUAGAGAUGAUGGGACUUUGUCAGAUUCUGAAUAUAUUUAGAAGGCUUCAGAAGUGAAGUAUGAGAGAAAGAAGAAUCCAGGAUGUGACUCCAAGUGUUUUGUCCUGAAAAAAUAGAAGAUUGAGAUGGGAAAGACUAGUGCUGGAACAGGAUUGGAUGAGGUGAGGAGUGGCUGUGUAAAGCAGGAGACACCCACCGUUCCCAGGGCGUAGUUCUGUAUCUGCCUUCCUGAGUUAGGCUUGGCAGUACGACUGGCUCUGGCCGGUGGGUCAUGUCGAUGUGAGACAAAAGCAGGGUACGGAAAUGUACUCCCAGAUCGGGCUCAGCCUCUUGUGAUGCAGUCAUUUUCAUGAGAAGAGCUUUCCUGGGGCAGACGUUGCCCUCUUAGCCUGGACCCCAAGUGAAUGCAAGUGACACAGAGCCACCCCAGCUAAGCCCAGCUCAUCCCACAUUUGGAAGGAGGGCUGCCCAUGGAGCCUGCUUUAGAUUACCAGACCCUACAGAAUCAAGAGAAUUAAUAGCUACUGUUGUAAGCCAAUGAGUUUGGAGGUGGUCUGUUAUGCAGAAGUUUUGUGGCAAUAGCUCAGUAAUAGAGAAUCCAGGGAGUGAAGUGAAAUAGGGAGUUGGAUAUAGGAGUCUGGAGUUGAGAAGAAGUCUUGGUUGGAGACAAAAAUGUAAGCGUCAUUGGCAUACCAAUGGUAUUUAAAACCUCAAGGCAAAUGAGAUCACCAUGGGAGUGAAUGUAGUAGAGAGGGUGACCGAAGAUUGCAUGACUACAUCAUUACAAUGUCUGGAAGAAGAGGAGCAACCCAUGAGGAGGAAGGAAAAUGCCCUACAAAUGAAAUGGAUGAAAACAAUAUCUAGGAGGAGGAAGUGACAAAUGAUGUCAAAGGCAACUGCCAAGAAUUGGUCAUUGGAUGUGGUAACCUGGGGAGAAUUGUUGACUUUGAUAAAUACAGUUUUAUGGGAGUGUUGGAGGUGCAAGCCUGAUUAGAGUGAUUUUAAACACGAAUAUAGGCGGAGAGCAACUGGAGAUAGAGAGCAAAGUAACUUUUUGAGGAGUUUGUGGGAAGGAGACAGAAAUGAAAUGAAACAAUGGCCUCCUCACAAAAGGAGCGCGAAACCAUGGUAAGGGUGUACUUUAUUCUGAGCGGGGAGGUAGUUGAAGCGUUUAAAUAAUGACCUAUUUGUCUUUUAGAUAUUGCUCUGACUGCUGUAUAGAGAAUGGCGUGGGGUGAAAGGGAGCAGAACAGUUAUAAGGCUAUUUCUGUUUCCUAGGUGAGAGAGUGUGUUGGCUUCAGCUGUAGCCCUGGAAAUGUGGAAAGUCAUGUGUAAAUUUCACAUGGGGUAAUGGUAUUAGGUAGACAGCAGUGUGGGAUCUUUAGCUUAAGGAACUUAAAAAAGUGUUUGUGAUCAAAUGAAAAAUCACAAAUGUAUAUGAGAAUUAUGUUUUGUAACUUCUCUUUAGCUCUACCUUAUCUUAUAUAAAUCAUACUGGUUUGAAGCAAUAUAUAUUGGUUACUUUAUUAAAAUUUACAUUCUGUUAUUUUUUUAAAUAAUUCCUGUUGUCUAUGAUAAAAUGGAUAUGACUGGCCAGGCAUGGUGUCUGACGCCUGUAAUCCCAGCAAUUUAGGAGGCCAAGGCAGGAGGAUCACUUGAGGUCAAGAGUUCGAGACCAGCAUGGCCAACAUGGUGAAACCCCGUCUCUACAAAAAAUACAAACAUUAACCGGAUGUGGUGGUGGGCGCCUGUAAUCCCCAGCUACUCAUGAAGCUGAGGCAGGAGAAUUGCUUGAACCCAGGAGGUGGAGAUUGCAGUGAGCCAGUCGUGCCUGCACUCCAGCCUGGGUGACAAAGUGACACUGUCUCAAAAAAAAAAAAAAUAAAAGUGGAUAUGGUAAUUUUUCUCCUUUCCAAAUUAUAUUUUGUUCCAUCCUGGAUCAUUCAGUCUACACUGGCGUAUUUCGCUCAAGUGACAUUAGAGAUGGUUUCUGGCAUAAUAUCCUUGUCUGAGUCUGUGUGCAAAAUAACUUUUUUAAAAAGUGGAAUAAGUUCUAUGAUCUGUAGUUGGGAUAGGGAUUAAACAACAACAGCAAAACAGACUUUUACUUCCUUAGAUCUCAGAUUUAUAUGUAUAGAGAAUUGGUUUUACACAAAUAGUGAAUAAAGUAUUUUGCCAAGUGUGCUUUCAGUAGAGACUUGAAUGAUUGUGAUCUGUUUUGCUCUUAUUCCACGUUCAGAGGUUCCCAUGGGAACCACUCCCAAUUCGUGGGAAGAGUGGAAUUUAACAAACAAUACAGAAAAGCCAUUUAAUCAUCCUCUGUGUGAUCCACAAAAGUGCCAGAAAUACGGAGGAAAUGAAAUCACUAGAAUCUCUAUCUGUAUGGGCCUGCCCAGAGAAAAAAGUGCUGCUCAUGGUAAAUAGAUUUGAUAGAUGGCAGAAAAACACCAGUGUCCUAAAUCUGACAGUAACAAAAAACCUCUCCCAUCAUCCAUCUCCUUCAGAUACCUUUUCAAAAUUUGUUAAGUGUUUUGUGUCCUAGAGUUUGGCAUCUUGCCAUUUUAAUUUAACUAUUUUUCCCCUGAAAGAUUUGUUUCCAGAAAAAGCUUGGGAUCAUAAUACAGUAAACCUUACACAUAAUCUUCUCAUUAUGUUCAGAAAGCUAAUUUUAAACCUAAUUUUCCCAUCUCUGUCUCUCUCUAUUCCAGUGCUUACCUGCCUGCAUUAAUUAAUUCCUGUGCAGCAAUGAAAAUUUGACUCAGUUACCUGACCUCUUACCUUCUGAUUGCAGAGGCUCUGUCUCUUACAGGGGUGUGGGACGCCUGGUGCCACAGGACAUGUGAACACAGAUUAUCCGUACCUGGGAGGUGACUUUGGUGAGAUCGGAGACAUUGGAGUCCCCCAGGAGCAGCUCCUCAGCAGAUUGGGGAUAAGAACAGAGGGCACCUACAACAAUCUAUGUAUUACAGAACACAGCUCUUUUUCUUUUGCGAACACAGCUGUUUUUCUUUUGCCUGACUUGACUGAAAACUGUUUUUAAGUGAAUUAAGUGUUUUAAGUGAAUUAGGUGUUUCAGCUAUGUCGCCAGUGGGCACUGAAUCCUAAAACAGUGAUCUGGAAGGGUCUUGGUGACCAUGCUAUCCAAGCACCAUGAGAUUUGGACCUCCAAGUUGGGUUCAUCUUCUCACUCUCCCCGUGCUCUCUACUGUGAAACCACAUUGGUCUUCGCUUCCUCCAACACAGCUAGCUCUUGUCUGCACCAGAGUCUUUGAACUGUGGUGCGUUUUACGUGAAAUACCUCCAAAUGAUUCUUGUUCAUCCUUAAGAUCUCAGAAUAGAUGUCAUUUCCUCAGAAAGCACCACCUUCUUGACCCUCCAGCCUACAGGAGGAUUCCCUGGACUGUGUUGUCAUAGCACCUUUGCUUUUCCAUCAAAAUAUUUAACAUAGUUCAUAAAUUGUUUCAUAGAUGAGGGGGUGGUUAGCUCGGGUUGCUUUUUCUCUUCUCCAGUAAGAGAUUUCAGAAUCACUCCCCUUAGAAUCAUUUAUAUGAGGUUUUCCCCUGAGGGCAGGCCAGUGGCCUCACUGCUUCAGAAGGGGGUGUAAUCAGGGUGAAGAGCAAAAAUGCUUGGUAUCUUUGAGGGAAAAGAAAUGAAGUUUUGGAGAGCUGGUAGGUGCCAGAGCCGUUCCUGCCUCAGUGCUUCCAUAACCAGCUGGGGACUUAGGAGGUGGCUGUUUGUGGGAUUCAAAAAACGGAACCAUGGGAACCUUGGAAGCCCAAGUGCUGGGCGUCUUCGAUGAGCUUAGCAUUCAGAAGAGAAAUUGCGCUUCAUAGGCCAUGUGGGGUCUGUGCAUAAACCUGUAUACAGCAGAGUUCAUUGCAGCAAUGGUCCCGCGCCUUCCUCAGCAGCGUCCUCAAGCAGCGCCACCGUGUGGCAGCAGUAAGCAAUGGCAGUGAUCGGAUUCCUGUCCACUCCCUGGUGUGGAUGUCCUCGGCGGACUUCCUGUCCAUUACGCAUGUGGGACAUCAAGAGAUAAAUCGGAAAAAUAAGAAAUACAACUGUAUAUGAAGCCCGGUUUGGAGAGGCAUUUGUUUGCAUAAGUCUGUAAGAUCCGUUGUAGACCCUCGGUAAAUGUUUGUUUUGGAGAUGAGGAAAUGGAGGCAGAGAGAAGGCAAGUCAUUUAUCACAGACAGCGUUAACUCUGGGCAGAGUUAGGAUAAGAAUAUGUGAAUCUUCUGGCCCCAGUUUUGGUAGUUCUGCAGUUGAAAGAUACCAUGAAGAAGGAUGAUGUGUAUUAAGAGACCAUGAUCCGAUCACUCUUUAUGAGAUUACUAAGAGCUAUGGAUUGCUAGGGCUAUUCCUGGCUAUUUGGGGAGAGGGAAGUCUGACCCUCUUGGAUGCUUAUUUUAUCUCUGGCAACCAUUUUGGGGUCAUUAAUAUUUCUCAUCUGCAUGUCUGUACCUCUUCCUUCCAGUUUUCCUAAUGACCUUCUUCCUUUUUGCCUGCCUCCUUGCAUUUCCGUUUCGUUGGUUUACCAAAUAGAUUUCAUUGUGAGAUAUGUGUGUCAUUGAGUCAAAUGUAUCUUCACUAAAAGAGAAGUUCUGGUUCCUGUUCUGAAAUUUCUGUCUUACACAUUUAAAAAUGGAAGAAGAUAUUUAAAAGUAAAAUAAAUUAAAUAAGCACACAUUAAUAUAAUGAGAUUACAUAAGACCUGGUGGAUAAUAUGUGAGACUGGGUUGAGAUUGAUGAGUGAUGGCUUCUUAGAGGAGAAAGAUUUUAAAGAUAUGCGAUAUGAAAGUAGAGGGAGGAGGUGUGCACUCCGACGAGAAAUGAGACAGGUGGGGAAGUCCAGUGUACAUGUGUUUACGGGGUUAGUGAGAAGAGAGUUGGCAAAAGUGUAUGGGAUUAUUCAGAACAAUCUGAGGAAAAGAUAUCUGGCUUAGGGAAGGAGUUCCUGGAGUCAAUGGAGACUUAAGCUGUUAAAGGAAAAUAAAAGUGAAAAAAAUGAAAAAAACUUUGGAGUAGUUUUUGGGCUCAAAAUCUCACUUUACUGUUACUAUCUGGGUGACUUUGGACAAGGUAUUUAAGAUAUGAAUGUGUUUUCUCAUCUACAAAAAUGUGCUUUUGUGAAAAUCAAGUAAAAUGUCCUAUGAGAUGCCCUAAAACAAUACUGGCCUAGAGGAGGUGUUCAAUAAAUGUAACUUUUACACUUUAUACCAAUUUCAAAUUCUCAUCACUAAGUUAUAGUUUCAAAUGAAUGUUUUCAGUUUAUCUUGAUGUUGCUCCUGACUUCAAAAUUUUCUGUUUGGAUUUUCUUAGAAAUUAAUAAUCUUUCACACAUAGCUAUCAAAUAAAUCAUUGUUUUCAUUUAAGAAACAUGGAUAAAUUGGCACACACACAAAAUCAUUCUCAGAAAUCUAUCAAAACCAAUUAAAGGAACCCCAAAUUAGGAAGGACAAUUGCAUUUGUCAUGAAAUUAGAGUGGAGCCUCAGCCUCAAACCCUAAAUUACAAAGACUAGUUUUUGAAUUCAAUUUAAUAGAAGCUUCCAGGAUUUCAUACAUAUGUUCUUUAAUUUUGCAUAUACUGCAUAUAUGGGAAAUGAGAAUGCUUGAAGGGGCUUUUAAACCCUGGUAAUUAGGACAGGGUGGCAAAGUGACACAUCAAAGUUUAUGUUCCAGAAAUAAAAAAGAAACUUGUGACAAAUGACUUACAAAGGGCGAAUUUUUUCCCCAAAAGUAUUAAUGUAAGAAGUUUAGAUAUGUUUCUAAAAGUCUACCAUCCCUCAUUAUUUGUCCAUCAUUAUUUCAGUACAAACAUACCCAAUGUUUCAUAAAAUAUAUUUCAUUAAUAAUUAAGACAGACAAGCUUUGAUUUAACAAUUUCUUACCAUAUGAAUGUGGUUGUGGUCUCAACCACUGGUAAAAGAAUUAUGGGGGACACAUUCAGCUGCUGCAAUAAAGACAACCAUUGUAAAUGCUUACCUCUUAGAUGAAAAUGGUUGGGCCGGAUGUCCUCCUAUUGUUUGCUCUUCCACAUCUGAAAAGAACGUAGACUAAAUGGAGUGAAUCCUCACUGAUACAUGGAAGUGAAUAUGUCCACAUUGGCAGCAUUCAUAAACAGCAGCAGGUUUCCUUAAUAUGAGAAUCAGAGUAGUUACAGCAUAGAUGAGUUUUUGAGCCUGCAUAGAAAAAGUCCAGAAAACAUGCAGCACGCACUGCUGGUGAGCAUUAACUCACUCUUGUCAUUUGGGAAAGAGAACCCAUUGUUUCUAGAUCUUCAAUUUCUGCAGAAAAGCAUGGAGUCUGUUACUCUUCAUUUUUUUGUUUUGUUUGUUUUGUUUUUGGAAGAGUGAAAUCUCCAGCUUUAAAAAUGUUGGCAACAAAUACAACAUUCUUUUUAAAGCAUAGUCAGUGUAAGCAUCGUUGGUGGGCUAGACAGGACAUACCUGUGAGCCAGAUUUGACUCACAGGCUUUCAGUUUGCAGUCUCUGAGGUCUAGUGUAUGAAGUUGGAAUCCCGAGAGGCAGCGAGUGGGAGAAAAUGAAGGCUCAGAACAAGUCAGACCUCUUGUAGCAGGCCUAUAACUUCUUCCUGGAGCACCUUGACUCUCUUAGCACCAUACAGGAUCUGAUCUGAGAGAGAGUUGUGUAAGAUUGAUGCUCCAGAAUUAUACUGUAUACUUUUGACCAGAAUAUUUUCAUUUUCAGUAUGAACACAUUGCUCUCUUAAGUAUUUUUUGCAUUUGUAAAAGAAAAUAAUAAGCCCCAACAUAUCCCUGAAGCUUACAAUAUCUGUGCCCCAAACUCUUCCUUAUGAACUUUCUUAAUAUUUUAACAAUAUCAAAACAGAAAAAAAAUUGUUAGGCAUAAAUUAUCUACUUACUCUGACCUAUAUCGGGUUCUUUUUCAAGCUUUUCAAAAGGUGACACAAAAGCCAGUUCAACCUGAAUAUUGGAAAAGAAUUGCAGGGGUCUCUGAGCAUUGGGAAAGGAUACAAAAGGCAUCAGAAGUUUGGCUUUGAGACAGUUGCCAUGAAAGGUAUCUCAUUUUCCUGCCCUGGAGAUUUUAUAUUAAAUGGAUUAUCUGUCUGUCAAGCAUUUUGAGCAUUCCCCUUCACUGCUUUCCCUGAGGACUAUUGCAGCAUCUUACCGUGUGAGGUGGGCCAUAUUUUUUUUUGCAGAUGAUUUAUAGAAUAUGAGAUAUAUAAGCAGCCGUUAACACAUCUAGUUUUAUUUUUAAAGUUAUGUUUGAAUGGAUUAUGUUUGUCCCACAAUCAUUUUUUAAUCUGAAUAAUAAGGUCAAUUUGACACAGCUCUUUUUUUUUUUUUAACAUUUAGUUUAAUCCUUUAACAAACCUUGCCCUCAUUUCUGUUUAACCUUGGACCACCUGCUUUGGCUGGUUAUGUAAUUUGCAAAUUAGAAAAUGACUAUUUCUUUUUUCUUGUUAUUGGACUCCAAAACUCACCCAAAUUCUUUUUCUUUGCUUUGUGUUUCCUCUCUGUCUUCCUAAUUUCUUAUGCCUGUAUUAAUAAAAUGGCUUGAGAGAUAAUAGUCUAGUUAAAUGCAUAGUUUCCUAAUUUGCUUAUGGAAAAGCUAAAGUAGACUGGAAAGAACAUGUUACUAAAUUAUAAUUUUAAAUUUUUUAUCAUUGAAUGUCAGUCUCACUGUGAUCCUUUUAUGACUCUAUAAAUAUGCUUUCUUUUGAAUGCUGGAGGUGGAAGGCAGGUUGGCGGUCACCUGGACUAAAACCAUCGUUUUACUGAAAAAGCAAUUGUGAACUAAAUAGGAGAGGUCUCUUGGCCAAGGUCAAACAUAAGCUGGUGGCAAAAUCAGGAGAGAGUCUUGUAUCCUGGUUAAGAGGUAUAAGGAUCCAGAGUCAGACAAAACUCCAUGUCCUGGAUGGCCUUAUAUUAGUUAUCUUGCUAUGACUUCUGGCAAGUCAAAUAACUUUUCUGAGCCUCAGUUUCAAAAAUUUUAAAAUGAAGAUUAUCAUAUUGCUCACUGUUAUUUAUAAUGUGGAAUAAGUGAUAGAUUCCACAUCAACUGCGUGACAUCUAACACCUAGUAAGCUCUCAGUAAGUUGUUACUGUUAUUGCUGCAUCUCUCAUAAUCAUCACUCUGAUCACCUGUCUAUGUUUGUGUCAUCACACAGCUCUAGCAAUGUUUCCAAACCAAAGAAAGGGUCCCUUAAACUUCCUCAGCAAGGGCUUGGCAUCUGUUGUCAUUUGUUGACUGUUUCUCAGAUGGUUCAGGAAUGUAUACGGUGCGUAUUAUUAAGUUUGCAGCUCCCCUUGAUUUCCAUUCGUCACAUUUGGUCCAUAAAUUCAAUCAAUAUGUAUUGAACACCUUCCUUCUGUACACAAAGCUCUACUAGAUCCCUAGGAUACAGGGUGAACAAGAAGGUAUAAUCCCUCUUGCCUGGGGCUUAUGUUUGGAGUUGGGAGAAUAGAAGCUAAAUAACUAAUCAUACUGUUGUUUACUUAUGGUUGUGUUCAGUGGUUAAAGUUGAGUACCAAGUGCUAUGAGUGAGUAAAAGAGGGGAGUCAAAGAUGGAGGCUUCUCGGACAAGUAGGUCUUAGCUAGGCAUGACCUAAGGUAUAAUUAUUUUUAUUUUGAAGGGAUGGUAUCUGAGGAGGUACAGGAAGCAGAAGUCAUUGAAAUUUUAGGGAUGAAUAGAAAGUCAUUGUGGCUGAAGCAAGGGGAUGCUGGAGGAUAAGGGUGGAAAGGAAGGAGGGGCUGAAACAUUAAUUUUUAGGCCAUGUUAAGUUUUCUGGGCUGCAUUAUAAGAAAAUAAAUGGAAUGUUAUUGAAAGGUUAUACACAGAAAAAUAUCAUCACCAGAUCUUUUAUAAAGAUAAUUUUAGUGCUUCAUGAAGAACAAGUAGAGGAAGCAGAGAGAACUGCUUGGGGUCGGGGUGGCUUGUAAUAGAGUGGGGGCAGUGGAGGUGGAGAGAGAUCUGAGAAAUACAAAGAGGUACAAGGAACCAGCCUGGUGUGUGACUGGUGUGUCAGUGGAGGCAGAGAGAGAUGUCAAGAAUGACUCCACUUUUGACAUGAACUCCAGUCAUCAUGAAUGUUGGAGUAAGACUGGUCCAUGAUCAUAUUUUUUUCCUGGUGAAAUAAAGCACGGAGGAGUUCUGAGUUCUGGAAAAAGACCGAUUGAAAUGAGAGGUGAAAAGAGAACGCUAAGUACGAUGAGGACAGAAGACAUACUUUAAAUAUGUUAAGUAGUAAGAACAUCAAAUACUAGGAGCCAGUAUAGUUAAGUUACGAAUUGUGAGGUUUGUGUAUGUUAGAGUUGAGGAAUUCCUGUUUCUUGCUGUUUUGAUGGGCACAGUGUUCUUCCACGACAGUAAUCAGAUAAACUACUUAGGUCAACUCAAUUAAUCUCUUUUAAAAGAAGCCUGGAAUAAUCUGCUCCGUUCUUUGACAUAAAUUGAUUGAUUAGAAUGUUUGCAUCCCCAAAUUAAGGUAAAACCACUGCCAUUUUACAGAAGGUAUUGAUCUUAUGUCUGUUAAAAUUGUAUCUUUAAAUUUUUUAAUUUAGUUUUAUUCUUUUUCAAUGAGAAUACAGAUUUCAAACUAAAUGUAGUGUAGGUGUGAAUGAUAAUAAAAUACCACAUAAUUUAGUGUAGUUUUCCUAUACGCAUUAUAUUCAUUUCAGCGCAUUAUGAUUUCAACUGUGUUUGUACUUGAAUUACUCAUUUUUGUUUAUCAACAUGAGGUUUCCAUCUGAUCCAGAAUCAAAUAGUUUUUAUUCAGAGUUCUAUUCAUUUACUAAAAAUAAUUUCUUAUGAAUGUUCUCAUAUAUGCACAUGCAUGCAUGUUUUAAAAAGAUAACAGAAUCCUGUUAUUGCCAAGAAAUUUGGGGGUAAGACCAUGGUGGCAAUUUAAGCAGGUUUUGUUUUGUUUUAGUUUUGUUUUUGAGAUCUUUAUUUCUCCCAGCUACCUAUCAAAUAAUAUAGGAGGGAAAACUGUGUCCCACAACUGGAAAACCCAUAAGGCUCCCCAGUCAUCUACCUCAAAUCUUGAGGAGUCUCCAGAGCUAUCAUUGUGCAAAGAGAUGUGGGGGAGCUGUUCUGACCUGUUUAUUGACUCAAUAGUAUGUGUCAUUCAAAUUUAGGGAAUGGAGAAAGAUGCUGUUGCCAUUCUGCUGGCCAUGUUACUUGUCAAAGCCCAUAACCACGAAUGUUUGGAGAAAAUUUAAAGUUGAAUAUAGGAGAGAACAAUAAUGAUAUGGAAGUUUCCUGUACUACUCAGGAGGAUAUCACAUUUAUCAAAUAAAAGAAACAAUAAGAAAACAGGGCUGGGUGUGGUGGCUCAGGCCUGUAGUCCCAGCACUUUGGGAGGCAGAGGCGGGUGGGUGGCUUGAGUCCAGGAGUUUGUGACCAGCCUGGGCAACAUAGGGAGACCCCAUCUCUACAAAAUAUAUAAAAAUUAGCUGGGUGUGGUAGUGCACACGUGUAGUCACAGCUACUCUGGAGGCUGAGGUGGAAGGCUAGCUUGAAGCCAGGAGGCUGAAGUUGCAGUGAGCGAAGGUCAUGCCACUGCACCCCAGCCUGAGCAGCAAAACAAGACCCUGUCUCAAAUUAUACUACAAGGCUAUAGUUACCAAAUCAGCAUGGUACUGGUAUAAAAAUAGCCAAGUAAACCAGUGGAACAGAAUAGGGAACCCAGAAAUAAAGCCAAAUACUCAUAGCCAACUGAUCUUCAACAAAGCAUACAAAAGCAUAAAGUGAGGAAAAGACACCUUAUUCAAUAAAUGGUGCAGGGAAAACUGGCAAGCCACAUGUAGAAGAAUGAAGCUGUGUCCUCAUCUCUCACCUUAUACAAAAAUCAACUCAAGAUUCAUCAAAGACUUAAAUCUAAGACAUGAAACCAUAGAAAUUCUAGAAGAUACAUCAGAAAAACUCUUGUAGAUAUUGGCUUAGGGAAAGAAUUCAUGACUAAGGACCCAAAAGCAAAUGUAAGAAAAACCAAAAUAAAUAAAUGAGACCUAAUUAAACUAAAAAGCUUCUGCACAGCAAAAGAAAUAGUCAGCAAGUAAAUAGACAACCCGCAGAAUGGGAGAAAAUAUUUGCAAACUAUGCAUCUGACAAAGGACUAAAAUAUCGAGAAUCUGCAAGGAACUCAAGAAAAAAAAAACUAAUAAUCCCAUCAAAAAGUGGGCAAAGGACAUGAAUAGACAAUUCACAAAUGGAGAUACACAAACAGCCAAUAAACAUAUGAAAAAAUGCUUCACAUCACUAGUUAUCAGGGAAAUGCAAAAUAAAACCAUAACGAGAUAUAAUCUCACACAAGUCAAAAUGACUGUUAUUAAAAAGUCAAAAAAUAAUAGAUAUUGGCCUGAAAGUGGUGAAAAGGUAACACUUUUACACUGCUGGUGAGAAUGUAAACUAGUACAACCACUGUGGAAAACAGUAUGGAGAUUCCUUAAGGAACUAAAAGAGAGAGCUAAGCUGUGAGGCUGCAAAGGUAUAACAAUGAUAAAAUGGACUUUGGGGAUUCAGGGGAAAGGGUAGGAGGUGGAUGGGGGAUAAAAGACUACAUGUUGGGUACAAUGUACACUGCUUGGGUGAUGAGUGCACCAAAAUCCCAGAAAUCACCACUAAAGAACUAUCUGUGUAACAAGAAACCACCUGUACCCCCACAACUAUUGAAAUAAAAAAGAAAAAAAGGAAAGCAAAAUUAAAACAAAGAAGAAAGAGAGAUUGCUUGAGGAAAAAAAAAACAACAACAAAGUAUACCCUUUAGUAGAGAUAGUAAAUAUCAGAAUGGAUGCUACUGACCAAAUUAAUUAACUGGAAGGCUGAGAAAAUUCGCAUAACUGUAAGUAAAAAAGAGGUUUUAUAAGAGAGAGGAUGACGCACAUAGGAUAGGUCUUGGGGCUCAUCUCAUAACUAAUAAUAGGAAUUUUAGAAAUAGAGAACAGAUGAGAGGAAGGAGGAGAACUAACAGAUUACCAUUUCCUCUAAGCCAAACCUAAUUCUUCAAGCCUUCACAUUGAAUGACCUCACUACAAGCUGGUGAAGAUUAAUGAAAAUAAAAACUUUUAGACAUACCAUGAUGGAAUUUUGAAUUCCAAGGUAAAGAGAAAAUGUAUACAAAAGUUGACACAGAAAAACAAUUAGUUACCUUCAAGGAAAAGAGAAUUUGACUAUUAUCCAGUUUCUCAUCUGCCACAGAAAAUGCUAGUGGACAAUGCAACAUUCCUUUCAGAACUGUGAGUAAAAAGGGUUGCAAUCAUAGUAUUCUCUCACCAGACACAGUUUGCUCAUGUUUGACGGAAAAAUGUGCGUUUUGAUACAUGAAAGGACUCAAAGUAUUCUGCAAAUGUACUGUUUAAAAAAAACAAAACAAAACAAAAGGAGGUAGUAGGAGGAGACUUAAGGAUGUACUAUAGCCAAAAUGAAAAUGAGUCAAAAUAUAUCACAAAUAGGUCACAAUAUGAGAAGGGGUGCAAGAUAUAUGGGUCACAAAUGCUGCUACAAGACUGGCCCUGGGCAGAUUGCAUUAAUAUCACCUAAGGUGGCCAGGCCUGGUGGCUCCCGCCUGUAAUCGCAGCACUUUGGGAGGCUGAAGCAGGUGGAUCAUCUGAGGUCAGGAGGUCGAGACCAGCCUGGCCAACAUGGUGAAACCCCAUCUCUACUAAAAAUACAAAAAUUAGCUGGGUGUGAUGGCGGGCUCCUGUAAUCCCAGCUACUCCAGAGGCUGAGGCAGGAGAAUUGCUUGAACCCAGGAGGCAGAGGUUGCAGUGAGCUGAGAUCGCGCCAUUGCACUCCAGCCUGGGUGACAAGAGCAAGACUGCAUCUUAAAAAAAAAAAAAGACAAAACAAAAACCACCUAAUGAGAUUUUCUUUCCCCAGCUUUAUUGAAGAAUAAUUGAAAAAUAAAAAUUGUUUACAUUCAAGGUAUACAACUUGAUUAUUUUGACAUGUGUGUACAUUGUGACAAGAUUACCACAAUCAAGUUAGUUAACAUCUUCAUCACCUCACAUAGUUACCUUUUUUUGUUGUGGUGAGAAUACUUAAGACGUACUCUCUUUGUAAAUUUCAAGUAUACAAUACAUUAUUACUAACUAUAUUCACCAUGCUGUACAUUAGGUAUCCAGAAAUCAUUCAUUCAUUAGGUAUCCAGAAAUUAUUCAAAGUUUGUGCCCUUUGACCAAAACCUCCCUGUUACCCCCACACCUGCCCCCUGGUAACCACCAUUCUAUUUUCUGUUUCUAUGGGUUCAACUCUUUUGGAUUCCACAUAUAAGUGAGAUCACGCAGUAUUUUUCUUUCUGUGCCUGGCUUACUUCACUUUGCAUAAUAAUGUCCUCUAGGCUCAUUGAUGUUGCAACUGGCAGAAUUUUUUUUAAGACUGAAAAAUGUUCAGCUGUGUGGAAUAUUAUAUUACUAUUAAUAUUAUAUGCUAUAUUUUAUAUAUACCACAAUUGUGAUGGGUGUACCACAAUUUCUUCAAUAUCAGGGCUAUUUUGAAUAAUGCUGUAAUGAACGUGGAAGUUCAUCUGUCUCUUCGAGAGAGCUAUUUUAUUUCUUUUGGAUAUAUACCCAGAAGUGGAAUUGCUGGGUCAUAUGACUGUUCUAUUUUUAACUUUUUGAGGAAUCUUUACUGUUUUGCAUAAUGGUAUAUUCAUUAUAAUGCAUAAUGUCAAUUUAUAUCCCCAUCAACAGUGUUUAAGGGCUUCGUUUUCACCACAUCCUUGCUCAACAUUAGUAUUCAUCAGGGAAACGCAAAUCAAAACCACAAUGAAAUCUCAUCUCACACCUGUUAGGAUUUUUUUUGGUUAUUAUCUAUUAUUUUUGAUAAUAAUUAUUAUCAAAAAGUGAAAAGAUAACAAGCAAGGGAAUUCUGCCAAGGAGACUUUAAAUGCUGAUUCCUGGAGUCCAAAGUGAGAGAUUAUGAGAGUGUAAACCUGAGAUAGGUCCCAGUAGUCUGUAUUUUUAAUAAGUUCUCCAAGUCACCUGACAGCCAAAUUUGGUAACCUGAGAGUAAUGAGUUCAGUAAAAUAUAUUACAAUUAAAUUAUUAUUGAUAAUGUAAGUUAUGAAAUAUUAAUGAAAUGGUUAAGAAAGGAUCCUCAACUGCAAGGACAAAAAUGCAAUCAUUUUUGUCUGAAAGUAAAUUCUAGCUUAUUUCAAGAGAAUCUAGGUGCUGUGUGUAUGUUGUGAAUGCUGUGUAGUGUAAGGGAAUCACUGAAGACUUAGAAGCUUGUAAAUGCCUAGCCUUGUUCCUGAAGGGGGAGCUCUUAGAGACCGUUUAGUCAUUGAGAUUGAUGGAGAAACAUUACUUACAUAUGCUUAUAUAUUUAAAGAUUACCAACAGUGAAAUACAAAUAAGAUGAAUAGCUCCUUAAUGGCUAGAGAAUGCAAAAUAACACAUAAGAAAAAGAAAGCUUCGAUAGUAGAGUAAAAAUUUGGAAGAAAGAAACGAGAAAAUAUAAACAAACAACUAUGAGUGAUAGAAUGUAGUUUGAUAGUAGUAAUCAUUUCACUAUGUAUAUGUAUAUCAAAAUAUUAUGUUGUGUACAUCAGACAUAGAUGUAAUAAAAAUAAAUUUAAAAAUAUAUAUGCAAGUUACAAUUAAAGUAGGUAAAUUAAAUCUUAAAUUACAAAACAUUUUUGCAUUAGCUUAAGAAGGAUAAACCAAUUCCAUGCUGUUUAAAAGAAGACUUUUUUUUUAAAUGGCACAAAGUAAUUGGAAAGUUUUUCACUAUUAUAUCUGCAGCUCUUGGCAUGAUUGGACAUAUGGUUCAAAAAUGAUUGCCACCUCAUGGAAUGAAUGGAUGUGGAAAAGUAUAACAGCCUCCUAUCACAACCACAACCAAAAAUAAAAAGUCUAGACUCUUGGUUCUGUGGUGCUGUCAUCUAUACCAUUGGUCCUUGGAACAGGAGCACCUAGGAACUUGUUAGAAACAGAAAGUCUCAGACUUCAUUCCUGACCUCGUGAAUCAGAAAUUUCUGGAGCCCACGCUCAAUCAGCAAGCACUCCAGGUGAUUCUGAUGGAUCCGAAUGUUUGAGAACCACUGCUCUGCUGCAUCCAGGGGAAAGCUAUUUACUAAGUCAAGUUUUAUUGUAAGUUGAUCUUUCUCUUUUGAGUAUAUCAGAAUUUAUUAAGAAUGAUUAGAAAAUUGAUUGCAAACCAAAGAGUGGAUAAAGAAAAUGGGGCAUAUAUACACCAUGGAAUACUACUCAGCCAUAAAAAAAAACGAAAUAAUGUCUUUUUCAGCAACUUAGAUGGAGCUGGAGGCCAUUAUUCUAAAUGAAGUAACUCAGAAAUGGAAAACCAAACAUUGUAUGUUCUCACUUAUAAGUGGGAGCCAAGCUAUGAGGAUGCAAAGGCAUAAGAAUGAUUUAAUGGACUUUGGGGACUUGAGGGGAAGGGUGAAAUGGGGGUGAGGCAUAAAAGACUACAUAUUGGGUACAGUGUUCAUUGCUUGGGUGAUGGCUGCAACAAAAUCCCGGAAAUCACCACUGAAGGACUUAUCCACGUAACCAAAAACCACCUGUACCCUAAAAACGAUUGAAAUAAAAAACAAAAAAAAGAAAACUGGUGGCAAGUAGGCCAGCCCAUGAAAGCCGUUUAAUACUUGGUUAAGUAGACUGACAUUCUUUUCGUAGAUGGUAGGGAGCUUUAAAGAUUUCUGAAUGUGAGAAGGACAUGAGUGGUUGAUGUCCAUCAGGACAACUGCUCUAGCUGCAGUGUAUAGCAGAUUGCAGGAGACUGACAGUGGAGAUGGAGAGCCAAGUUAGAAGGCAAUUAAAUAGGUCAAGCAAGAGGUAGUAAAAACCUGGAUUGGAGUAGAGGAAAUGGAAUUGGAAAAGAGACAAAUGAGAAAGAGAGAUUGUGAAAGUGAGAACAGUGCUUGGUCCCUGAUGGCAUGUAGGGGCCAAAAGAGAAGAAAGGCAAAGAUGAUUGACGUUUUAAGCCUAUGUGACAGGUAUUAUUGGCACUACAGAUCAGAACAACUAUCAGUGAUCUGCAACGUGGUAGAUUGUGCUGAUAUCAGUCAUCACACAGAAGAUUGGUUUGUUUGGAUUUCUAAAUUGGGGCUUUUCAGUUCAUUGGAAGGAUGGUUAAAAAUCUCAAUGAUUAGCAUUAGAACAAAAGAGAACAGAAAUACAGUUGAGUACUUUGCCAGACUCAUCAAAUAUGAUUUUGAUGGGCUAAGAACUCCUAACGAGGACACAGUGAUCAACUGAGCAAACAGACCAUUUGGCUUGAACAGAAAUGUCAACAUAGGCAUAAUCUACUAAGUUGCUAAUUAGGGAUGGUACUAGCCGGUUGAUGGACUUCAGCCAAGACAUACAGAAUGGUGAGAAGCCAGUGCACAGAGCCUCUGGGAAUCUGAAUGAUCAAUUAUUUUUCAUCCCAUAAUGUAAUUUACCUGUAUUAGAAUUUAUAUGCAGAAUUAAACACUCCUUCUUCAGAGUUUCCACAGUAUUCUAGAUUUUUAUUGAAGUAUUUAUUUUAAUGGUUUAUUUAUCUUGGGCAGAGCUUUUUGUGGGGAUAUCAAACUGUUAAUGGAUAGAAAGGGAUAGAUUGAAUAUUCCUGAGAGUUGGAUCAGUGUGAAGUAAAGUUGAAGUUGGUUAUACUAUGGCAAGUAUGAUGUAGAGAAAAUCUUUCGGAUGUUCGAAGGUCAACUCAGCUACUUACUUCCUUUUAUAAUUUGGUUCGACUUGAACACUAUGAUUCCUCAUUUGUUAAAUAGAAAUAAUAAUAAUAGUUUACCUCAUAGGGUUAUUAUAAGAAUUAAAUCUAAAAUCCAGUUGACUUGAACUCUAAAAGAUAAAAUAAAAUUUGAAAAAGAACUAAAGGAAAAAAUAAUUAAAUAAAAUUAUGCAUAUGCAAUGUUAAAAAACAGAAUCGGAAAAAUAAUUUCUCAAAGAGGGUAGCUGUUGUUGCUAUUAUCGUUGUUUUAUUUUAUUGUCAAACAGGCUGUGAGAGUCAACUAGAAGGGUGACGAUCUUGAGGUAAGAAGUUUUUGCAUCCCUCUAGCAUAUUUUACAAGCAGCAUCAGGUACAAGCUAAAUGAGUGUCGCUGAGCCUGAACUUGUUUGGUGAGUAGUUGAAUAAGGGAAUGAUAAGGCCCACAUUCAUUUAUUUUUACUUUUAAGGUAGAAGGGUGCAGCAACUUGGUUUCUGCAGAAUGUAUCACUUGCUGUCUUUUCCGUGGAAAAGAGGCUAUAGUUGUUCAUUCAGAUUGAACAACUGAUUGUAAAAUUGUAAUACCCCUAGAUGGAGGUGUAUAAGAAAACUAAGCCAUUUCUUUUCUUAUAAAUAUGCAUACAUGUCUUAGUUCAUUCAUGCUUCUCUAACAGCAUAACAUAGACUGGGUGGCUUAUAAGCAACAGACAUUUAUUUCUCAAAAUUCUGGAGACUGGGAUUUCCAAAUCAAGGAGCUGGCAAAUUGGAUGUCUGGUGAGGGCCCACUUCUGGUUCAUAGCCAGCCUUCUUCUCUCUGAGUUCUCACAGGGUGUAAAGGACCAAGGAACUCUCCUGAGUCUCUUUGAUGAGGGCACUAAUCUCAUUCAAAAGGGUUCCACCCUCAUGAUCUAAUCAUCUACCAAAGGCCUUACCUCCUAAUAGUAUCUCUGAUAGGCCAGUCUUGUGUUGCCAGAAAUGAACAUUCUCAAGUUCAUUUCAUGCCAGAAAGGAAUAUCUGAGACUGGGUAAUUUAUUUUAAAAAGAGGUUUAAUUGACUCACAGUUCUGCAAGUGGUAUAAGCAUGGCAUUGGCAUCUGCUCAGCUUCUGGAGAGGCCUCAGGGAGCUUUCAGUCAUGGCAGAAGGCAAAGCAGGAGCGGGCACAUCACAUGGCAAAAGCAGGAGCAAGAGAGUGGGGAAGUGCCACAUAUUUUCAAACAACUGUAUAUGGACACUCAUUAUUGUAAGGACAGCACGAAGCCAUGAGGGAUCCUCCCCCAUGAUCCAGUCACUUCCCACCAGGCCCCAUCUCCAAAACUGGAGUUUACAAUUCAACAUGAGAUUUGGGUGGGGUCAAAUGUUCCAACUAUAUCACUAUCACAUUGGUGAUUAGGAUUUCAGCAUUUGAAUUUGCAGGGGACAUAAAUAUUUGAUCUAUGGAAAUAUGUAUAAGACAUUUAUUUAAUCUAUAAAAUAAGAUCUCUAAUGAAUGUGUUAUAAAAGGUAGCUUCUAGGUUCACUGUCCUAUUUUAGGAAACUUGCAAAUGUUCAUUAGUCUCCUAAACCUCUGCCGAUAGCUUGCCUUUUCUUUGUGACCUUGGAUUUUUUUUUUGUAGGAUUCCCUGUCUAGAAUAUCCUAGCUUGUUUUUCCUAAACAUGGAAAUCACUAAUCCUUCAUGGCCGAGUUUACCAUCCUUCUCCUUAGUAAUUUCGCUUUAUUUCAACAAGGAAAAAAAGUCUGAGAAAUUCUGUAGCACUUUGGUCCAUUGUUAUGACAUGCAUUUCAAAUGACCUAACACUGUUUAUAUUUGUGUAGAAAUUUUAUUUAUCUUAUUAGAUUGUAAACUCCAUACAAGAAAGCUGAAAAAAUAAAAUUAAGAAUACGGGGAAAGGUUUGAAGCAGAAGGUCAGAGACAGAGGCUUCUUCAAUGCCAUACAGAGGAUUGGGCUUGAGUAGUAACUACUGCUUGAUACCAGAUGACUUAAUCUCUCUAACCAUGAUGUAAUGAACCAGAGGUGGGUCCCUGUCCCCAAAGGACUGUGAUCCUUAAUAAGUGACUUGGUAAGAGCUCUGGCUAACUGGUGUGUUGAAAAUGUCACAACACCCUAACCUGAUCUGAUCAUACAGACAGAAUGAGCAGAGUGAUUGGACUAAAGCUAAAAGGCAGAGAGAGGGCAAUGAUAUUACAGGCAAGCAGCUAGCACAGCAAAAAAUUCAAUGUAAAUAAAAUAGUAGAGUUAGGAGAAGAUUAUCUGCCCUCUUUACCAACCCCUUCAUCUUUAAGUUAAAUCUCAUGAACUCAAGUUACCUGAAAAUAUGGUUUAUUCCAUGUAUGUGAAAAAAGGCCUGACUAGUACAGCAUCAUUUUGUAAUCUCUUUGGCAGAAAUGAUUCUUUUUAUAUGUUGAGUCUAAAUGCACUGCCUUGUAGCUUCCAUGCACAGGUACUUGUCAUGCUUCCUGAAAUCACACAGAACAUGCAUUAACUAUGUAGCCAAUGACAGGCCUUCUAGGAUGAGCAGAUUCUUCAACAGUAGGGAGAUGUCUUUCACAGGAAACGAAUGAGUAUUUGUCAGGGCUUCACUUGAUAUACUUUCUACCACUGUCCCGGUAAGGAAUAGCAGAAUAUAAAUAAAGGGUCUAAUAUGUACUUAUUAAUGAGUUUGCUAAAUAGAAUAUAUAUACCACUUAGUGAGUGGUACUAUGAUUGUUUUGGGUACAUACCUAAGAUUAGCUUUUGUUUUAAUAGUAGAAAUAUGUAUAUAUUAUUAUGUAUAUUAGGAAAAUAUAACCAGCAUGGAAAACCCAUGGCUUCCUUGAGUCUAUUCAUUAAGACAAAUGGAAAAUACAUAUUUAAAUUUAAAAUAAGAAUUUAACAAUGCUAAGUAAACAGUUCUAGUGGUAUGCACAUAUGGCCAACAUAAUGGAGGAUGUUUGCUAAUGAUGGUAAUUAGUAUAACACUGCUUUAAGAAAAAGUGUCAACAGAUUAGCAUGAUAUGCCACAAGCAAACUGGACCAAGAUUAUCACUUUUAUUUUUGCUUUCUAAUUUCAGCGGUUAAAUUUUAAGAUAUUUGAUAUAGCUUAGGAGAUUGAUUGCUUUGAAAACCAACUUAAAUAUGAAAUAAAGAAACUAUACUAGCACAAGUAAUGCAAGAAAUAAACAUCACUUCAAGGUCAAUAUCAAGAAAUUGGAACCCUUUCUGAAUUUAUAAGAAUAUUUUGAGAAACAACUUUCCUGUCAAAUGGAAGUCAGGAGAAAAUCAACAAAGAGUCACCUUUGUACCCAAGAAAACCUAUAGACACAUGUAACAGCAUGCAGAAAUAUAAAGGUAAAAAAAUCACUCAAGAGUCAGUGAGAAUUUUUUUUAGUAAAGGUCAUUUGAUGUCCACUUCCUUGUAUAUCAAAUAGUUAAAUGCGGAUGAAAGCAGGAGAUAUGAAUAAUACUAGACCGUGUAUCCAUUAAGGAAUCAUGAAAACAAAAGUUUAAAGCAAGAAUUGCUAAAACCAAGUGUUUUCUCAAAAGAGCUCUUAAGUCAAAUGUAGAGGUAAGAAUAUAUGACUUUAUCACUGUAUCAUUUUAUUACAGGAUGGAAUUCAACAUUUUCAAUGUGAUUUUCAUGUAUUUUAUUGAUUUGGGAAGGUUAGCGAUUAAAUAUUGUUAAUAACAUUCUACCUGGUUUCUCAACAUCUCAUAUCUUUUUUCCUCUGACCCAUCAGAAAUACUACUGGCACACUUGUCUCCCCAGUGCACUUCUUGGAUUGUUUUUGCUCCUCUGCUCACCACACUUCUUGAGGCUGCUUCCUGAAUUCCUCCAUACAUAUGAAUUCUUUAGCAGGCUAUUCAGCAUGCCUGUGCUGUCUGUGCCAAAUCUAACUUCCAGUCAUUUUCCUUUGCACUUGUGUUUGGCUACUUAGGUUUAUCUUAAUAUGCUCUAUAUGCCAGGGCUCUUCAGAGAAGCAGAACCAAUGGGAUUGUGUGUGUGUUUGUGUGUGUGUGUGUGUGUGUGUGUGUGUGUGUGUGUAUCUCCAGGAAACUUCAGUUUUUACAUUUAAGGCUUUCAGCUGAUUGGAUGAAGAUCACCCACAUUAAGGAGAAUAAUCUCCUUUACUUAAGCUGAAUUGAUUAUAGAUGUUAAUCCUAUCAACAAAAUACUUUCAAAGCAAUAUCAAGACUAGUGUUUGACCAAACAACUGGGCCCCAGAGCCUAGCCAAGGUGACGCAUAAAAUUUAACCAUCACAAUUGCCUUGCUUUUCUUUCUCUAUCGUCUGGAUUUUAAAAUUUUUUAUACUUUACCUUAUAUGUCCUUAUUCCAUAUUCCUAAAUUUGAAUACCCUUCAAGCCCCAGCUCAUUUCUCUCUUAUUUUCAAAGUCAUUACCAUUCACUUCAUCCUGGAAUGGUAGCUAGGACCUGUGAAAUUCUGUAGCAGGAUGCACUGCUUUCAUAGCAUGCAUUUCAUGCUGCCUGGUGUUGAAGGUAUUUGUGUAAGGCUUUUAUACUCUGUGAGAGCUUUGAGCUUCUCAAGGGCCAGAGCUGUAACACAUAUGUCUUUGAAUUAAUAUAUAAUUCAUUGCUCUACACAAAGGUACAUACUUUUUUUUUUGUUUUCUGAAGUGCAGAGUGCUAUUCUAAGCCAUCUUAAACUCAAAGAAUUAUAGAAACGUUCUGGCAUACAGUCAGAAUAUGGAAUAGGAAGAGUGUUUCACAAAGUGUGAUAGGCAUCCUACCACACAAAGUAGUGUUUGCUUUAAUAGAUUCAUGUUCAUGUUACUGUGAUUUAGAAAAAAAAAAUUGUAACAUCAAACCAAUGAAUUCUCAGAUAUUAAUGUUUAGGAUGGUGUUAAAACAGAGACUUAUGUUAGGCUUGAAUCAAUGAUUAAAUAUUUAUUUGAGGGUCAAUGUUCAAGUAUGACAAUGUAGUAAAAUAGUAUGUGAAGAAACUAGGUUUGUUCCAUGUUAACUUAAUGCAGUUCUAGACUGGAAAUGAGGAGAAUUGAAAUUCUAUAGGCCCAUCACUCAUUGUGUGUGUGAUCUUAAGACAUUUUUACCUCUUGGCAUCUGUAUCUUUUUUGGGGGGUAGGUAUUCUGUUAUCAUCUAACUCUAAAAGUGUAAUUUGCUACUAAGAUGCCUAUAAAUACAGCCAGACUACAACACAGAUGGUGCACACAGGAAGAAAAUCUCUGAUUGGUAGACUAACCCAAAAUAGGCUGUGUAUAUAUUGAAUGAAAUACGACCAAAAAAUCUGCAAAUAGCAGACACAGAGCAUCCUUUAGGUUGGAACUGAGUAAAGUAGAUUUAUGAUCUAAUCUUACUUAUUCUAUGACAUUUCUGUUUAAUGAAUGUCCCUGAUCCUCCUGCCAUCUUACUCACAUUUCUAAUGUGCUCAUACUCCGAGGUAAUAAUGAUCAUUUGCAAUUAUAAAUGUCCUGUUAUCAAUUAAUUUGCAGUUCACCAGUAACCAUCUGAUUAUCUCUAACAAAGCUGCGCUGGUGUGGUAAUUAUGUUGAGAGUAAUCAUCAUGUAAUUGCACAUAAUUAUUUGUACCUUAUUAAGUGCUCAUAUGAUUAAAAUAUUUCUGGUCAAAUAAAAAUUAUCCGUGAGAGUAUUUUUUGGAGGGGGGAAAUAAGAAAUGUUGCUUCCUGGUCUUCUGUUCUUUGAAUAAGGUAAAGCUGUCUAGCUGACAGUCCAUAAUGCCCCAGAUAGGAUGAAUUAGUAAGGAGAGAAGAGACUUAGAUUUCAUUAAUACAAUACCUUGUACCUCCAAUGAAGUUGAGAUAAUAAACUUCAACUUCCAGCAUGGAUGAACGCUUUCCCUGUAGUAGCUAUAACAAAAAAUAUUACCCUAUUAAGAGUGUACACUAUGAAUGUCAUUGAGGACAAUGUGUUUUUCAUGUCCAACACCGCCAUUAGCAAUUUUAUACUGAACUUUUAUUUUUCUCAUAGUACUCUCUCUUCAAAACUUUUAAUAUUCACUUAUUUACACUCAGUGUUUUUUUUAAUUUCCAGGGACUGUGUUUAGUGAGAUGAUCUACAGGUAUAAUUCCAAAAGCACCUACCAAAUUUGUUUAUUCAGACAUUCAUUAAAGAGCAACUCUAUAUACUAGCACUCUCCUUUAGAAAUAUUAUGUGAGCUACGUAGCCAAAUUUACUUUUUCCAGGACCCACAAACAACAGCAAGAAAUAGGUAAAAUUAAUAUUAGUAAUAUAUUUUAUGUAAAAUAAUCAUUACUUCAUAGGUACUCAGUUGUAAAAAAGAUUAGUGAAAUAUUUUACAUUUUUUGUACUAAGCCUUAUAAAUCUAGUGUAGAUUUUACUUAUAGCACAUCUCAAUUCAGAUGAGCAACAUUUCAAGGGCUCCAUAGCCAUAGGUAGCUUAUGGCUGCUGAAUUAGAUGGUGCAUAUAUGUUGAUUGUAUCUACAUGGUAGAUAAAGGAGAGUCCUAAUUAAUAGUUAGCUCUCUGAUUUUAUAGAUGUUUUUAUGAGUUUCAAUUUCCUAAUCUGGUAAAUAAUACAUCUAGCCUAAAACAUUUCUUUUUAAAUUAAAAUGUUUUCUAGAAGGAUAGGGAUGGAACUAACAUUAAGGGACUGCUUUACUAGGUCAUGUAGGAUACUAGGUAUAUUUACAUUUAUUAUCAAAUUCAUUCUUCACAAUAGUCUAGAAGGGUAUGUUACUUUACAGGUUAGAAAAGUGAGAUGUAAAGUUUAACCUUAUCAAUAGUAGAAUAGUAGAACUGGGAUUCAAACUUGGCUAUCAUCUUUGACCACAGAUUUUGUCUCAUGCUUUUCAAAUAAGAAACACAUAUUUUGGGUCCACUUGCUCAUUGAUAGGUCUAGUAAGAGGAUUUUACUUCCCUGAAUACUGUGUAAAAGGCUUGACUGCAAGAAAGUUACUGAUUAGUUUGAUUUUUAGGGUUUCUCCUGACCUUCCUUAUCCAUGUUUCCCAGUCCAGUUUCUUGAAUUAGUCUCUCCUGAAAGCUUGUUCUUUCCAGCAAACUUAUCUCAAGUAUAGCAUAAAUCAUCUUCCACUGGCAUUUUAACUGAAAGUCUGUUGACUAUCACGCACACUUACAGAAAGCCUACCUUUGGGGAUAACUGAGUGACUGACAGCGAUGCCUUAGCAACCAUCUGAUUGUAGUUACAGAGGAAAUUUACCUUGGAUUGAAGAAUCACAUGCCAUUGUGAUUGACAGAGUCUGUAAGACAAUCAAGGUCAAACCCAGAGUAAAUUGAGUAUGUGGCUAUGAGCAUUGACAGAUAAGUCAUGUGUCAAAUAUUGCCUAGCCAUCUGGUUGCUACUCAUGAUUAGACUGGAUUCAUUGUGUUUAAUUUCUUAUUGAGGACAACUACAUGGGAAACUUGUUUGUUUUUAGUUUAUCAGUGAAAUGUGCUUUAUCUGCUGACAUAAAAUGUUUCUGCCUAAAGUGAACUUGCAAAAUCAUUAGUUUUAUGACUCCAGCAUGACCUACAAAAAAUUAUUAUUUAAAAGUGAUUGAUGCAUUAUUGAAAAAAAUAUAUUAGGUGCUGAAAGUUACACUCAUGAAUAAAAGCACAAUUCCUUAAAGAGGAAUAAGAAAACAAAUGUGAUCACCCCGAGGGUUUUUAGAAGCCCCCAAAUGUUUAAAGACUAUUAGCCAAACUGGGUACCAGAUAUGUGGGUAGUGAGAGGUGAUGAGAUGUCAGUGAUAAGUGAUGUAUAAGGGGACAGGUGCCUUGUGUGAAAUUCUGAAAAUUCACAUUUAGUAGAACGUAUCAAACGCCAGUAGAACGUAUCAAACGCCAGCAAAUACUUAGUUUAUUUUUGAGGACAAAAGUGGAAAACACAGGGAAGUGAAAUCAAUUGUCCUAUGUCACAUUGUACUUGGAAUGGGGCUCUGAGUCCCCUGACUACUAAUCCAGUGCAAUUUCCUCCUGUAACUUUGCUGCCUUUGUAAAUGAUUACAUUUUAAAUACAAGGGCUGUUUGGCUUAUUAAUUAGUUAGUGUUAAAAAAAGCCAAAGUUGCUUUUCAUCACUGAUGGAUUAGUACCUUUCAUUCUGUUUUCAACUACCAUAUUGUCCUUUUAACUGAACUAUUAAAAACAUUUUUCCUUGUUGAUCACAGCUUGGGUGAACAAAGUAGGGGCUAAUGAAAAUAAAUUCCCGGUCAGAGAAAAUGGCAGUUGCACGAGUUUUGGUGGUAUGAUAGUCACAUUUGCAUAUGUAAAGUAUAACACUACAUAAGCAAAUAAUAUGACCCAAUUUUAGGUGGUGAUCUAUAUGUCAUUGCUGGUUCCUCUGCAAGAAUAAAUACUGAAUGCUUCUAGGCAUUUCCAGUAAGCACAGUAAAUCCAUUUCAAUAAUGAAGAAUUCCUGAGAAAACAAUAUAAUAGAAUCAACAGGUUCUAGCAAAGUGGAAUUUUAUCAUAAAUUACAAGUUCCACCAUGUUAACACGUACAUUGCAACAUGUUUUGGACAGUACUUCUGAGGUUGGAAUUCUCAGCAAGUGGUUCCUAUUUUGACAUCCAGACAGUGAUAGCCAUUUGUAGGUGGAAAAUUAGUUAUCAGCUGUGCCUUGCUUUUUCUUUACUUGGGUUUCUCUAUUUCUCUGUCUUUUUACACACACACACAUACACACACCCCACACACAUAUACACAUAUAUAUCUAUCCUUGGAUAUCCAAAAAAAGAUUCUCAAUAAAUUCACAACACUAAUUGAAUUGAGAUGAUAUAAAGUUGUUGAUUAUUUUUAAUAAAGUCUAGAGAUCUAACAUUAGUUGUAGCUUAUUUCUUCACUACUAAAUAAGAAAUUCCAAGUUAAGUCUUUUCAUCUUUUCAUUAAUAAAUAGCCAAUAUGUAAUAUCUGCCCAUCCAUAUAUAUUAUGAACUAUCUGAACUACUCCUUAUAAUUAUGGGGUAACCAGUCAAAUAAAAGUGUUGAAUAAACAGCUUAUUGUAUAUGUUAUGAAUUACCUGACUUAAAAUUAGGAGUCAAUUAGUCAAAAUGCCAUGGGCUAUAUGACUCAUUGUAACAUUAAUAAAGUAAAAUAUGUCUUCCUAUAAUCCAGUUAUUGGUAUUAAAUAAUAUUGAAGCUAUUUUCCAAGCAAAACUUCCGCAUAAGUUUGUUUUUGUCUUGGUUGAGAACUGGUUCUUUUGAGAUAAAGCCACCAACUCAGCACAGGUUUUUUUUUUUUUCUCCUGAAUGGUUUUGUUCAACUUAAAAUGACUGUUCCUAACAGCAGGUGCUCUCUUCUUUGUUUCAGAUUAUAUUGAACAUGCUUUUGGUCUUCACAAAUACUGAAAAUCAACUAUAAAAAUGCUGGAUGAAAAGAACUAUAUCCAUAUGGUAGGAAGAUAAAAUUUUAGCUCUAACUCAUAUCUUCUCUGAAGAAGAUUCUUCAGAAUCAUUGACAUAGAGUAACUCCACAGCAUGUGUCUUCAAGAGCUUCCCUAAAAGAUUAAAGGUUAUACAAAACUUAAAAGAAGCAGCAAUUCUAUUCGCUUGUUAUUGGACUUGAAACUCCCUUUGACCUCGGAAACUGAAGAUGAGGUUGCCAUGGGAACUGCUGGUACUGCAAUCAUUCAUUUUGUGCCUUGCAGAUGAUUCCACACUGCAUGGCCCGAUUUUUAUUCAAGAACCAAGUCCUGUAAUGUUCCCUUUGGAUUCUGAGGAGAAAAAAGUGAAGCUCAAUUGUGAAGUUAAAGGAAAUCCAAAACCUCAUAUCAGGUGGAAGUUAAAUGGAACAGAUGUUGACACUGGUAUGGAUUUCCGCUACAGUGUUGUUGAAGGGAGCUUGUUGAUCAAUAACCCCAAUAAAACCCAAGAUGCUGGAACGUACCAGUGCACAGCGACAAACUCGUUUGGAACAAUUGUUAGCAGAGAAGCAAAGCUUCAGUUUGCUUAUCUUGACAACUUUAAAACAAGAACAAGAAGCACUGUGUCUGUCCGUCGAGGUCAAGGAAUGGUGCUACUGUGUGGCCCGCCACCCCAUUCUGGAGAGCUGAGUUAUGCCUGGAUCUUCAAUGAAUACCCUUCCUAUCAGGAUAAUCGCCGCUUUGUUUCUCAAGAGACUGGGAAUCUGUAUAUUGCCAAAGUAGAAAAAUCAGAUGUUGGGAAUUAUACCUGUGUGGUUACCAAUACCGUGACAAACCACAAGGUCCUGGGGCCACCUACACCACUAAUAUUGAGAAAUGAUGGAGUGAUGGGUGAAUAUGAGCCCAAAAUAGAAGUGCAGUUCCCAGAAACAGUUCCGACUGCAAAAGGAGCAACGGUGAAGCUGGAAUGCUUUGCUUUAGGAAAUCCAGUACCAACUAUUAUCUGGCGAAGAGCUGAUGGAAAGCCAAUAGCAAGGAAAGCCAGAAGACACAAGUCAAAUGGAAUUCUUGAGAUCCCUAAUUUUCAGCAGGAGGAUGCUGGUUUAUAUGAAUGUGUAGCUGAAAAUUCCAGAGGGAAAAAUGUAGCAAGGGGACAGCUAACUUUCUAUGCUCAACCUAAUUGGAUUCAAAAAAUAAAUGAUAUUCACGUGGCCAUGGAAGAAAAUGUCUUUUGGGAAUGUAAAGCAAAUGGAAGGCCUAAGCCUACAUACAAGUGGCUAAAAAAUGGCGAACCUCUGCUAACUCGGGAUAGAAUUCAAAUUGAGCAAGGAACACUCAACAUAACAAUAGUGAACCUCUCAGAUGCUGGCAUGUAUCAGUGUUUGGCAGAGAAUAAACAUGGAGUUAUCUUUUCCAACGCAGAGCUUAGUGUUAUAGCUGUAGGUCCAGAUUUUUCAAGAACACUCUUGAAAAGAGUAACUCUUGUCAAAGUGGGAGGUGAAGUUGUCAUUGAGUGUAAGCCAAAAGCGUCUCCAAAACCUGUUUACACCUGGAAGAAAGGAAGGGAUAUAUUAAAAGAAAAUGAAAGAAUUACCAUUUCUGAAGAUGGAAACCUCAGAAUCAUCAACGUUACUAAAUCAGACGCUGGGAGUUAUACCUGUAUAGCCACUAACCAUUUUGGAACUGCUAGCAGUACUGGAAACUUGGUAGUGAAAGAUCCAACAAGGGUAAUGGUACCCCCUUCCAGUAUGGAUGUCACUGUUGGAGAGAGUAUUGUUUUACCGUGCCAGGUAACGCAUGAUCACUCGCUAGACAUCGUGUUUACUUGGUCAUUUAAUGGACACCUGAUAGACUUUGACAGAGAUGGGGACCACUUUGAAAGAGUUGGAGGGGAUUCAGCUGGUGAUUUGAUGAUCCGAAACAUCCAACUGAAGCAUGCUGGGAAAUAUGUCUGCAUGGUCCAAACAAGUGUGGACAGGCUAUCUGCUGCUGCAGACCUGAUUGUAAGAGGUCCUCCAGGUCCCCCAGAGGCUGUGACAAUAGACGAAAUCACAGAUACCACUGCUCAGCUCUCCUGGAGACCCGGGCCUGACAACCACAGCCCCAUCACCAUGUAUGUCAUUCAAGCCAGGACUCCAUUCUCCGUGGGCUGGCAAGCAGUCAGUACAGUCCCAGAACUCAUUGAUGGGAAGACAUUCACAGCGACCGUGGUGGGUUUGAACCCUUGGGUUGAAUAUGAAUUCCGCACAGUUGCAGCCAACGUGAUUGGGAUUGGGGAGCCCAGCCGCCCCUCAGAGAAACGGAGAACAGAAGAAGCUCUCCCCGAAGUCACACCAGCGAAUGUCAGUGGUGGCGGAGGCAGCAAAUCUGAACUGGUUAUAACCUGGGAGACGGUCCCUGAGGAAUUACAGAAUGGUCGAGGCUUUGGUUAUGUGGUGGCCUUCCGGCCCUACGGUAAAAUGAUCUGGAUGCUGACAGUGCUGGCCUCAGCUGAUGCCUCUAGAUACGUGUUCAGGAAUGAGAGCGUGCACCCCUUCUCUCCCUUUGAGGUUAAAGUAGGUGUCUUCAACAACAAAGGAGAAGGCCCUUUCAGUCCCACCACGGUGGUGUAUUCUGCAGAAGAAGAACCCACCAAACCACCAGCCAGUAUCUUUGCCAGAAGUCUUUCUGCCACAGAUAUUGAAGUUUUCUGGGCCUCCCCACUGGAGAAGAAUAGAGGACGAAUACAAGGUUAUGAGGUUAAAUAUUGGAGACAUGAAGACAAAGAAGAAAAUGCUAGAAAAAUACGAACAGUUGGAAAUCAGACAUCAACAAAAAUCACGAACUUAAAAGGCAGUGUGCUGUAUCACUUAGCUGUCAAGGCAUAUAAUUCUGCUGGGACAGGCCCCUCUAGUGCAACAGUCAAUGUGACAACCCGAAAGCCACCACCAAGUCAACCCCCCGGAAACAUCAUAUGGAAUUCAUCAGACUCCAAAAUUAUCCUGAAUUGGGAUCAAGUGAAGGCCCUGGAUAAUGAGUCGGAAGUAAAAGGAUACAAAGUCUUGUACAGAUGGAACAGACAAAGCAGCACAUCUGUCAUUGAAACAAAUAAAACAUCGGUGGAGCUUUCUUUGCCUUUCGAUGAAGAUUAUAUAAUAGAAAUUAAGCCAUUCAGCGACGGAGGAGAUGGCAGCAGCAGUGAACAAAUUCGAAUUCCAAAGAUAUCAAAUGCCUACGCGAGAGGAUCUGGGGCUUCCACUUCGAAUGCAUGUACGCUGUCAGCCAUCAGUACAAUAAUGAUUUCCCUCACAGCUAGGUCCAGUUUAUGACAAAAGUUAUCUGAAGGACUUGCUGUUUAUAAUAUAAGCAACAUUUAGCUAGUUGUUUUGAAGACACCCAGUACUAAGUAAUAUUGUUGUUCAAGUACAUCUUAUUACUGGAAUAAAAAUGUUUUUUGCUUCUUUAGGAAUGGCAUUAUACAGUACUUCCUCAAAGCAAAUCUAGCUUUGUCUGAAGUUUCUUUGGAAACUCUGCAAUGCACUGAAGACAUCUGUAAUAUGAUGUUACCAAAGCAGUUUACAUAUGUCCUUAUAUGCAUAUUUUUUAUUAUAUAUUUAGUGUUUUAUAGAAUUUUUUAAAGUUAACAUAUAAUGUAGAUAUUAAUUUUUUCCUCGGCUGUAAAAUGCUAUGGGCAACACAAUCAUGCAAUUAUAAUUUGAAAAUAUUUCCUUUAAAGACAGAGUUUGAAACUCAUCUUGGUAAAUAAAUUGCAAAUUACUCGUACAGUUUUACAAGGAUCUCAUGGCAGAACAGCGGAAGACUUGGUCCGUAACUCAAGGCUGUUGUAUGCAAACUACUCUUCUAGUGGUUAAUGCACUUGACAUGUACAGUAUGUUUCCCAUGCCGUUGUGAUUUUGACAUGUACAGUAUGUUUUCAUGCCGUUGUGAAUUUUGUUGUUCAACCCAACUUGAGAUGGUUUCAGGAAUGGCUGCAAUCUCAAAAGCUCAAUGUACUGCCCAAGAGGCACCUUGUGCAAUAUUCCCAUCCCUGAAUUUAGCAUUGUACAGGAAGAUUUUCUUUUCACUCAACUGAGUUAGCAUUGUCUUUGUGGUAGCAUUAUCUUAGACAUUAAAUUUGAAGUAACAUAUAUCCUGUAGUAACAUAGACCCAAAGUUACUAUAGUCAACCAAGUCUUUCAAAGGAUAAAAGAUCAUUUUAUUAUCUUUAACUGUAUCUAUUUUGAAUGUAAAUUUAAAAAAAGUAAUUCUCUGUCAAUGGAUUCGUAAUUUCUUUACAAAAUUUCUUAUAUAUAAUAUGUGUAUCUCUGUAAUAAUAGAGCCCUUCUUUUGAAUCAAAAUUACAUAUGGACUUUGGAAGAUUGCUCCUAUUUCAACAAAUAGUUGCUGCAAGAAUUUUUAAUAUGACUCUAUAAAAGCUCUUUAGUACAAUUGUAUGGUUUCUUGAUGAUUCUGUUUUGCAAUAGGUAGCCUAGUUGCUUUAUAUGCUUUACCUUCUAGGUCUUAAAAUCACACAUUGGAAAAUGACAAUAUCAACAAAACUGUAUUCUUAUGAAAAGAACUAUUUGUUACAAUGAGAAAGGUUUUGUGAGUAAACCCUACUGGACAGUGACAUAAAAGGCAAUGGAAUUUUCUAUAAACAUUUUCUCAUGUAAACAUGCUGCCACCUUUUCUUCUUUCUCAGAGAACUCAAAUUUGCUAUAGUUUGUCAUUUUUGCUUACAAAUAAUAUAACUUUUCAACCUUCUAGUUAUAUUUAUCCAAUAAAGUCAUAAUCGGGAUUCCAUUUGUGUAAAAACUAGGGUGGUAACCGGAAAAAAAUAUUGUCAGUAUUUCAAGCUGUGUUCCUUUCUUAGUUUGAUAUGGUUACUUCUAUGUUGAAAUAAAAUUUAAAAUCACAUGCAAAAAAAAAAUCAGCAAAAUAAUAAAAUGAACGAAAAAAAAUGACACCCAGGGAGUUCCCAACCCCAGUGUAAAUGAUAUUUACCAGUGAUCUAGCAUAUGUAAUCUUUUUUAAAGGUAUUGUUAAUAAAUAUUCUGUCAUUUGUAAA